CAGAUCACGUGAGCCCAGGAGUUCGAGACCAGCCUGGUCAGCAUAUUGAGACCCUAUCUCUACAAAAUAUUUUAAAAAUUAGCCCGGUGUGGUGGUGUGCACCUGUAGAUCCUGCUACUCAGGAGGCAAAGGUAGGAGGAUUGCCCAUGAUCAUGCCACUGCAAUUCAGCUUGAGCAACAGAAUGAGACCCUGUCUCCAAAAAAAGUUUUACUGAAAUAUAAUUUACAUGCUAUAAAAUUGUCCUUUUAAAAUUCUGGGUUUUUUUAAUGUAAAAAGAAAUGCUGGUGAUGACCCCACUGACUUGUAAAAGCAUGACAGUGCGAGGAGCAGUGCAGAGGCACAGUUGGAUUAGAGACUGUCCACCAGGGAGGCAAGAAAGGCAGGCCAGCACCCAGCCUUGAACCACUGUGCUCACUGCAGUCACUGGACUGUGUUUCGUUAAACACCCUUAAACUUGAGCAAACUGGCAGUUUUACUCCUUGGUGUGAGAUGAAGGCUGGGGUAAGCCCACAGGUAAAACUGCUCUGGUGGUCAACCAAGGGGCUUGCCUCAUAGGAAGGUGAAAUGGGCACCUUCUUUUUGUGGUUUGUGGUGCCAGCAUCCCCUCUUCUCUUUGCCAGGAAGAAAGAGAGAGGGAGAGGAGGGGGUAGCGGAAAGGAAGCUUUGUCUCAUUAGACAGUAGAGCCUGAAAUUCUUGUAAUUCAUGUUACUCUAUUUAACUGAGUUUAUUCAUGAGAAUCUUUGAGAGAGUGACUGUAGGGACAUGGGUAUUUGAUCAGUUUGCUCUCAUUAAUCUGCUAACCAAAAGGAGAUAGAGCACCACGGAAAUGAAAUAGGAAACAACUAAGUUUUCAUUAGGAAAGUGGAAGAGGAGAGGGACUAAAGAAUGCAGUGUAGCUUUGCUUUGUUGGGUUGUGUUCAUGGCCAGAGGGAGGCCCUGUGUGGUGAGGGUAAUCAGCUGUGCAAGCAAGGAAGCCAGGGUGGAGAGGCUCAGAGAAGAGAUUUGGUGCCGGUGCCAGGUAGGGCAGGAAUAUGACAGGACCAAAUAAAACUGAGGGAUCCCUGUCCCGUCCCAGAGCAGUGAAAUAAUUGGAGCAAACAUUUAUUGAGUGCUCACGAUAUGCCAGGCACUGUAUCAUCUCAUUUAAUCCUUUAACACCACAUGAAAUUUUGGGUUCUGUUAUUACCUUCAUUUUACCAAUGAGGAAACUGAGGCACAGGGAGGUAAAGUAACUUGUUUGGGGUUGCACAGUUACUUGUUCUGACAUUUAUAUAAAUGCAGGGCAUUGAAGAUCCUGCCUUGAAGCGAGUGAACCCACUGCUUCUGGGACCAUAUCUGCUAUACCAUAGCUUCAGGAGCAUACCUUUCCUGGCAGAUCCCAUAAUCUUUGAGUCAUUUAGUCUCCAGGUUGCUACCUUGAAGUUCACUCUUAGAGGCUGGUGACCAUAAUACUAAAAAUAACACUGUCCUAGAGAAUAUUUAUAGUUUUUUCACUCCCUCUUCAUAAGUACAGACUGUGCCUUAUCUAGGAAAUACCACUUAUUUUGGGACUCUAGAGUUGGGCAUAUAAAUUGUAAGGCAUGUCCAGUAGUAGUCGUGUUUCAAGUCACUUCAACAGACAUUUUCAUGCUUCUAAAGAGCCCUGCCAUGUACUUCGUGCUAGAAUGGCAAAUGUGAUCUCAGGGGAAAUAAACAUGACCAAUAUUUAAAUUGAAGUGAACCAAAGUAAUAGAACAGUAAAAGGAACAUAGAAGGAGGGUGAGGAGGUUAGGAAGAACUUCCCAGAAGAGUUAACAUCUGAGUUGGGAUUUGAAGGAUGAAUAGGAGUUUGUCAGGCAGGUAACAGUCACAGAAAGAUUAAGUGAAAAUUCCUGGAAAGGUGGGCAGAGGUUUUCUUCUGAUUUUAUUGCCAGUGUGUCUAGAUUUUUGAUGUGAUAGAGCCUUCAGUUGUAAAAUUCCACUUUUUUCUCCUAGUGACUUGAAAUGCCAUUGGGAUCCUAUGCCUCAACAGUGGGGCUGGGUAUGUUUCCAGCCAGUCAUAGGGAGGGGCAAAUGCUACCCAUGCAGCACCUGUAGGCACACUGCAACUCUGGACAGAAGCAAGUUUCUUGUUUGUGUGAGGUGAUGGUGGUGGUUAGCUUAGCUCCAGCCCAAAACUUUGACUGCAAUUGCUUGACUAGAUUUUUCUUCCCUUAUAUGAAAAUAGUGUAGUUGAUUGUUGUUAUUUAGAAAGUAUUUAGGCGUUCAGUCACAAAUGUUUAUUGAGCAUUGAUGUUUGGAUGGGGGUUGAGGCAGAUGAGGGCCAUAUAUAGAACUUGGGUUUUUGAAAUACAAGAUAAAUUUCAGUAAAUGGUACUAAUCUCAAGUAUACUGCUUGAUUAUUCUUUUAGAUAUGUAUAUACCUGUGUAACUGCCACCCUCAGAUCAACAUAGAGACUGUUCCAACACUCCAUAAGGUUCUCUUGUGACCCUUCCUGGAUAAGACCCCCCCCUCACUCUACCCUACUCCGCUUAGUUCUGGCUUCUGUCACAAAGAUUAGUUUUGCCUGUUAUUGAACUUCAAAUGGAAUAAUACAAAAUGUCCUGUUUCGUAUCUGGCUUCUUUAGUGCAAAGUAUAUCUGUGAGAUUCAAAUUGUUGGGAGGCAUUGAUUAUAACAUAUGAUUUGUGCCAUUGAGGGUUGGGUCUGGAUUUGUUGGUGGCAUUCAUUUAUUCAGUACACAUUUACAGGCACUCUACAGGGGUUUACAGAUAAAAGAUAAAUACAGUUCCUGCCAUCAAGGACUUUUCAGUGUAUUGAAGGAGACAGACACACAAAUGUUACAGACAAGUGCUCGGUGCCACAAAGAAAAACCAGCACUUAGAAAAUUUCUCAGCAAGGCACAUUUACUUCUGCAGAAUGGUGCUGCCUGCACCUGUCUGAUCACAAGAGCACACUGAGCAGGGUAGAGCAGGGUUUUAAAUCCCUAUAUAGUUCCUGUUUCUGUGUCCUUUCCCCAUUGGCUGGAGUUGGACCACACAGUCUAAGCUGACCCAAUUGGCUAGUGUUUAAAAUGGAAUAAGGCCAAUUAGGCGGGAAGGGAGAGGCUGUCUAUUACCAACUAGUUGGGAGGGGUUGUUUACAGAGUCAGAGAUUUGCUAGUUAUAGAUUAAGCAGAGAAACAAGUGUUCAUUACAGAUUAAGCAGGAAGGGCUGUGUACAGAGAGAAAGACGAAGGAAGCUUUGAAGAGGAACUUAUUGUGUCUGGCAGAUUUCCCCCUCUUGAGUUUAUAGUUCUUCCUCUUCAAAUUUUUGUAACAUAUCUUGGCUUUGUUGCUCCUCUUGGUUGUCUGGGAGUAGGAACUUAUCCGAGUAGGGAGGGGGAGAAUCGAGAGGGGUUUUGGUGGGGGCUGUUUUUAUAAGCCUUUGCCCUGAUCCACAAAUACGAGGUAUGGUGCAGCAACCUACAAGAAUGAGUACACCUAUAGCAAUUGCAAGGGGGGUAAAGAUUGAGGUUAUGAGUCCCUUCCAUUUUCUAAACCAUUUUUCCAUGAGACCAGAGAAGGGGUAAUCUAUUCCAGAAUUUUCGGCUAAUUCAUUUGCUAGGGUGGUAAGGCCCAGGCUUUUGUAAUUGUUCCAUCGGGGGCUGUGUUGUUAGGGAUAAAAGUACAGCAUUGGACCCCAAUCAUGACACAGACUCCCACCUUUCUUGGCUAAUAUCAUGUCCAGGGCUAUCCUGUUUUCCCAAGCCAUUUGGCUGUUAGGACCUAAUUGUUCAGCUAUUCCUUUAAUGGCAUCCCUAGUAUAAUUGACAAACUGCUGUUGAUUAUAGUAAAUGUAAUUUAUCCAGUCUACACUUUUGUUUACAGUUUCCCAUGAGAACAAUAUAGAUUGAAAUCCUGUAGCUAUUUGAUUUUGGGCUUUAAAUUCAUUUAACACUCCUCGUGGAACUCCGAUGGCAUCUAUGUAAAUGUAAGGGUCAGAGGACCCGUAGGGAGUACUCCUUUUUUUGUGAUUGUCCUUUUUGCUUAGUCGACGAAAUGCCAGGGUGGGAUGGCCAAUUGAAUUAGGGCGCAAGUGUUGCCCCACUUAUUUGGCAGAGUACCCAAUAGUGGUCCACCACAGUACCACCAUACAUCUGCUUGGGGAUGAACAAGGGCAGACUGAUUGGUUAGCUCCUAGAAAGGCUUAGGCUUACUUCAUCUUGCUAGAUUUCCAAGGAAUGCCAAGUUUUCCCCUUGCUGUGAGAGACACGAGGUGAAAUUGACAUUGGUACCUGGAGGACAGAUGGCCCUUGGGGGCUGACCCGCAGGGCUUUUAACUUCCGGGAAUAACAGCAAGAGAGUUUGGCAUGCCUUAUUGCCCCAGGCUGUGGGGUUUUGGAAGAGAGAUACCAUACAGCUCAUACCCUGUUGGUCGGAGGACCAUCCAAGUAGAAAGGGGAUGAUUUGGGUUUCUGGCCUGCCCGUUGCACAAGCGUUAACAGUCGCUUUUGUUUAGUUUGCGGACGGAAUAUUUAAUCCGUGCUAGCCAGGCAUUUGCAUCUUGGUACCCUGUUUCAAUAGCUAGGGUGGGUUUUAAAUCUUUAACUUCUACAGUGGCUACUUUGGGAGCCAUUGCAUUGUAGGGAGAGACUAGUAGUUUGAUUAGAAGGUUUGAAGGAGAGGGCGGAGGGGAUGACGAGGCAACGAAACUAAUUUUGAAAAAUCCUGUAGAGUCUGCCCCUGCGACCUCUGCUCCCAUACCCUAGAAACGACUUAAUGAAGGGAGGAAUUUUGGGAAAUUGAGAUAGUAAUGGAAAUUUGUACUGGAUUACAUUAGUUUUGCUGGCAAUUGGUGGGGGGGCUUCCUUUAGUGAAACAAUUGUAUAGUUUUAGGGAUACACAGAGACUUGUUGGGGAGGUCCAACCCUGAUUUUUCGUAGUCCAUAGAACAUUGGACCAGCUAUGGCAGAGACGCUCUGUUUGCAGAGGACGGGAUUCCCAGUUAACAGAAUUUUAAAAAUAAUAUCCCAAGUCUAAGGGAACUCCCCAGUUAAUAGAAUCUGCCCAGUCUGAGAAUUUCCAAGAAGGGCAAAGUAGAGAGCUGCCUUUGACUUCGCAAGUCUCCACAGGGUAUAACAAGACAAGCAUCAAAAGUAAUGAUUUGCGGUGACUCUGAUGCGUUUAUAUUAAUAAUGAGAUGUGGGGUAGCUAAGGGAAAGAGAAGAGGAAAAAAAAAAGGAUAGACAGAUUAGGCUUUUUUCUUUAACAUUACUCUGAUGGGGGUUGGUCCUGGGAUGAUGGUCCUUGACUUUGGAGAGGGCGAUGCCUUUUUGACCCGGGUAUGGUGGGUCAACCCCUUCUCAGUGGUUCAGACUGCUGUUUCAGUCGUUAGGAGCACUAGAUAAGGGGUCCUUCCCAGGUGGGUUCGAGCUUUCCCUCUUUCCAACUUCUGAUAAGGACAUGAUCUCCAGGUUGGUGUUGGUGAACUGCGAAUUCAAGGGGUGGAGUUUGCGCUAGGAGGCCUUGAGUCCUGAGAAAGGAAAGGGUAGAAGACAGACCAAAUACAUAGUUUUUAAGAAACUGAUCCUUUGUCUCAAAUGUCGGGAGGUCCGUAGUGGAAUUUAAAUAAGGCAACCCAUAAAACAUUUCAUAAGGAGAUAAGCUGAUGUCUUUCCGGGGAGCAGUUCGGAUUUACGUCCCACCUCUAAAUUUAUAAGGGGCUCUUGGUGGUACUUGAGAUAAAAGAAACAGAAUCCCUGACCUCCCUAUUCUUCUUCAAAGGCCGUAAGUGGGAUGACUUCUUUUUCUUUUUCCCAUUUGGGACAUUCUCUUUUGAAGUGACCUAUUCUUCCACAUUUGAAACAUUUGUUUUGCCCUCUUUCUCUCCCUGUUUUUAAGUUUCCUUGCUUUGCUUUUACAUACCCUUUAUAUGGCCUAGUGAGUGGGGGCUUAAGUUCUUUACAGGUUUUGGACCCUCGGGUACUUUGUUGUAGAGCGGACAGCAUGAUUUUUUGCCUUUUGCUUUUGCUUUUCUUUAUCCCUUCUUACAUAUACUUUUUGGGCCUCCCUCAAAGGUUCCUCUAUAGGCCGAUCUUUCCAUUUCCAGUUCUCUAUUUUUUGUAAUUUCUUUGUGAUAUCUGGCCAACUAUUAGUAACAAAAUGGAGCUUUCACAUCCCCUGCCCAAGGGGAUCCUCUGUGUCUAAGCCUACAUAUUUUCUCAUCUGUUCCUUGAGUCUGUUUAAAAACUCCAUGGGCCCUUCAUCUUUUCCCUGCUGUAUAUUAAAUGCUCGGGAAAUACUUUGGGUUCAAGGCACUGAUUCCUGAAUCCCUUUAACUAUCAUUUCCCUAAGGUCUUUCAAGUUUUCUCGGUGGGCUGCAUUGUUAUUAUCCCAUUGCGGGUCUUGGGCCAGAAAUUUUUGUUCUGCUGCAGGGAUAUUUUGACCGGGAGGAUGUUUGUGCUCCCAGACUAUCAUAGCAGCCCUGCGGAUCAUGGUUCUUUCCUCCCUCGAAAAGAGAAUACUGAAGAUGGACAUUAACUCAGCCCAAGUGUAUACUUGUGGUCCUAAAAAUUGGUCAAUUUGAUCCGUGACCCCAAAAGGAUCAUCUAAUAGUGGUUUAAGUUCCCUCUUCAGGUUUCUGACCUCUAAACUAGUUAAGGGGGCAUUUACAAAGCCAAUUCCCAUUCCUCCACGUGGCACUUCUCUUAAGGGAAAAAGGGUUGGGGCAGACUCCUUUUAGGAGAGGAAAGGGAAGUUGUGAGUGUCCCUGUGGCAUUGUUCUAUUUCUCGUUGGAGCUUCUCUGAGGGAGGGGCAUGUUUGGGCGACUACUCCAUAGGAAUGUGGGGUGACGGGGCCCGCAGGGCAGGGUUAUAUGGUGGAGGGACUGAGUGUUCAGCUUGGGGCAGAGCGGUGGGUGGGGGAAGGUUGUCUAAAGGGUCCCAUGUGGUGUUAGACUGCUUGGGGGUAGGGAUUCUGUUUUCAGGGGAGGUAGCUUUUGGCUUAUUUCCUGUAGCUUUUAGGGGGUAGAGGAGGACAGGCCCCUGCCGCCAGCACAGGGCAUAGUCUAUUUCCUCCUGGGAGACAGGACUUUUGUCAUUGACAUAUUCUAUUAGAAGUUGACAAAUCCAAUCCUCAUUUGACCCAAACUGGCCAAAAAAAAAAGCAAACUGAGGGUUCAAGGGUGGGUUCUUUGGUCCAAAUAAAACAACAAUAUUUUAUCAUUUGUUGCUUUUUCUAAUGUUUAGUCCUUUCAUUACCCUUACAGUAUUUUAACAUGAGACCUGGAGGGCUAUUAGAGGGAAUUUUAUUGUCUGUCUAGUCCUUUAUAUUUCCUGUCCUGCUUGGGUUAUUUCCCAUCCUGGAAGUUUUAGGUGUUUCCCUGAGUUUCCUGCAUGUGUGGGGCUAAACCUCUCUUACUAGAGAUUUCUUGCACCCUUUCUCUGGAGGCUCAACCACCCCACUGGAGGUUUCUUGCACUCCUUUGCCUUCCCUUCAUCCUUCUUGGGCCGCUUCCCUCAUGGGAAUUUAGGUCCCUCUUAGCAUUGGUGGGUUGGUAUAAACCCCCGACAGGAAAGGCGUGCCCCACCUUAAGCUGUAUGAGGUGACCACAGAACUGCAAAUCUGGACUCCACACUUGCUUCAGACUUAAUUCUGCAUCUCAUUCACACACUUUCAACUUCCAGGGUGUCCUGACCACCAAGGAAGUACUUCACUGCCCCAUGGAUUUUCUUACAUUGGUCUGUGCACAGUUACUGGGUCGCCACAGUAUCAGUAGGCCCUUUCCUCCUGCGUUGCUGAGAGUCUGGGUUUAUUCGUCACACCAGGUGGGUCUCGAUCCCUCACCCCUGAGGCCACUGCAACAAGGCAGUGGGACACAUCUCCUCACAAGAGAUGAUCAGAGACCCUUCCCCAGAGGAGAAUGGGAUCCUGGACGAUCCCUCAAAUUGUUAGAGACAAGUGCUCAGUGCCACAAAGAAAAACCAGCACUUAGAAAGUUUCUCAGCAAGACACAUUUACUUCUGCAGAAGGGUGCUACCUGCACCUGUCCGAUCACAAGAACACACUGAGCAGGGUAGGGCAGGGGUUUUUAUCCCUAACACAGUUCCUGUGUCCUUUCCCCCAUUGGGUGGAGUUGGACCACACAGUCUAAGCUGACCCGAUUGGCUAGUGUUUGAAAUUGAAUAAGGUCAAUUAGGCGAGAAGGGAGAGGCUGUCCAUUACCAACUAGUUGGGAAGGGUUGUUUACAGAGUCAGAGAUUUGCUAGUUAUAGAUUAAGCAGAGAAACAAGUGUUCAUUACAGAUUAAGCAGGAAGGGCUUGUGUACAGAGCAAGAAAGACCAAGCAAGCUUUGAAGAGGAACUUAUUGUUUCUGGCACAAAUAAUCACAAUGGGUGGUAGGUCAACUUUUAGGUGGUGAAAAUGGUUUUCAAAAGACUUUAUAGAGGUGGUGAGUUUCUUCUGAUUCUUAAAAGAUUAUUAGGAGUUUUCCAGAUAGUCAAAGGGCAUGAUAGCUCGUGCACAGAUGUGGAGGUGUGAAGUGGAGCACAAUGUCUUCAGAGACCUGCAGUACCAGUACUUUGAUUUUAGAUUGGUGUAAGAAUGCCAAAAACAUCACUUUGGGAAGAAAUUUUGAGGAAAACAUUGUCAUAUAAGUUUGACUUCCAUCUUAGGCUGGAGCCAUGGGAUGUGACCACUUUAGCAUAUGGUCCUGAAAAUACCAUAGUGGAGAAGGCAAAGAGUGGAAGUGAGCUGCAGCUAGGUAAAAAGGUUCCAACAGUGCUUUACUAUUGAUACUGUGGAACACCUUUAUGAGGUUAGAUAAAAACUAUAGGGAUGCUUAUUAUGAAUGUGGUGUUUUUUUCAAUAAUUGAGAUGAAUUGAGGUGUUCCAUUAAGCCAUCAAAAAUCCCAUAAGGGUAGAUUUAGAAGUAGCAUCUCUUCUUGAUCAUGGGAUUUUUUUUUUUUUUUUAAGCAAAAUUUGUUCUCCAUUGCAUUAGUUCGUUAGGGCCAUACCAAAAUACUACGGACUGGAUAGCUUAAAGAAUAGAAAUUACGUUCUCACAAUUCUGGUGCCUGGAAGUCCAAGAUCAAGAUGUCAGCAGGUUCGGUUUCUUUCUUCUCUUCGCUUGUAGAUAGCUGCCUCUUGCCAUAUCCUCACAUGGUCUUUUCUCUGUGUUUAUCUAUGUCCACAUCUCAUCUUUUUGUAAGGAUACCAGUCAUAUUGGAUUAGAAGUCACAGUAAUGGCCUCCUUUUAACUUACCUCUUUAAAGACCCUAUCUCCAAAUACAGUCACAUGCUGAGGAAAUAGAGUUUAGGGCUUCAGCAUAUGAAUUUGGGGGUCAGACACUGCAGCUUAUAACACCCAUGUUUCAAAACUUAUUAUAUUAAGAGUUGGGUUUUUGGGGGGUUGUCACCAGAGAAAAACAGGCUAGAAGAGCUGCAAUAUCAGCAGGUAGCAGUGUUGUAGGCCAAAGUCAUGUGGGACCCCUGUGGGUGCUGGGCUUGCUUUUAAAGUGCCAUCUCUGAGUUCUUAGUGGCUUGGGUCUGUGCAUACAGAAAGCCUUUGGGUAGUAUAGCUUAACUCCUUGUGUGUUCUCAUAAAUUAAUGCUGAAAAUAGAGACUAAGAAGUAAAGAAACCAAAGUGUAAAGGCCAUGUGAGCAUCACAAGGGAGAUAAUUUCAUAACUUUUAUAACUCUGAAUUUAUUCUAGUGAUGAACAAACCAUAUCCCUCUUUUACUAUUUAACCCCCCCCCCCCUUUUUGAUUGGGCUGAGUUAAACAGUGUUGGCAUUCUCCUUAUCAAAACAUUUGGAUACCAAAGAACUGUUUUAAAAUGCCUGAAUCUUCUCCUUGGAGGCAAGAAAUUGUUUUCUGUAGAAGGAUUGUAUUUUGAUUUUUCUGUUGUUUUUGCCACAAAGAGGGUGGAGGGAUAGGUUUUUUCUUUCUUGUUUAAGGAAGUCUUUUAAGGAAGUGCUUUUACAUAGUCACUUCUUAAAUUAUUUCUUAAAUUGAGUUUUGGAGGGGCACGUUUUAGAUACCUGAGAACUGGAAAUCUUUGAUUUCAGUGUAAUAGUAUUUAUUAUAAUGGUAUGUGUCACAGAGUUUGUACUAAGGUAUGUUAGCUCACACCCUCUGGUGUUAGACCCAGCCUAAUGUAAAACAGGGAAUCUUGGGAAGUCAUGGCAUCCCCGGGUGUUCUCAUGUUGCAUCCCUGCUAAUGCCAGUGCUGUUCCAUUGCCUUUUUGUUCCUUCCCUUAGUCAUGGACUUCUUGACCACUAAUUAGAUUUUGCCAGGAUAGUCUAGGUCAGAAGCAGGCAUUUUUAAAUCUUUGAACAGCAGCAAAUGUAGUGUGCAUGGUAGCUCCAGUUUCUAUUUGUAUGAAUAUGUGUACUCGUUGUCUUUAAAUGAAGUACUACUAUUGUGUCAUUGUUAAUACUUUUAAAAAGGAGUAAAUUAAUUGUUUGAAAUGGAUCAUAGUUCAAAAGUAUAUCUAGAUUUUACUUAUUUUUGAGGAAAACUAUCUUUCUCAAAAGACUCUCGUUUAAGACAGUAAACAUUACCUAUUACUCCAGCAAAUUAAAUGUGUUAACUUUCCAAGUUUUUCUAUUUUGUUUUCUGCCAUUUCAUUCUACUCUACACUUAGAUUUGACUUUACCCACUUUUCUUGUGUGUGUGGUUCAUGUCCUUUUUUUAAAAAAAAGAAAUUAGGUAGAGAAUACCACUUACAAAAGUUUUUUUUGUUUUGUUUUGUUUUUUAAACCAUGAAAAUGCUGAUAGUACUCAAAAGCUUUGGAUAUUGGGAACCUGUGACCAUUGGACUCACGGGAGUCUGAUUUGAAAUUCUUUUUUUUUGUUUGUUUGAUACAGAGUCUCACUCUGUCGCCCAGGCUGGAGUGCAGCGGCACGAUCUCGGCUCACUACAAGCUCUGCCUCCUGGGUUCACGCCAUUCUCUUGCCUCUGCCUCCUGAGUAGCUGGGACUACAGGCACACGCCACCACACCUGGCUAAUUUUUUGUAUUUUUAGUAGAGACGGGGUUUCACUGUCUUAGCCAGGAUGGUCUUGAUCUCCUGACCUUGUGAUCUGCCUGCCUUGGCCUCCCAGAGGGCUGCGAUUACAGGCGUGAGCCACUGCGCCCAGCCUUGAAAUUCUUUAUACCUUAGUGGAGUGGUCUGUAUGUUUUAUCGGCACCUUCCAUCUGUGAAAAUCCUUGAAUGGUUGCAGCCGUAUUUUCUAGACAUGUCUACUGGCUUUGUUUUUUCUUUUGAUUUGGAGUUUCAUUCUUGUUGCCCAGGCUGGAGUGCAAUGGUGCAAUCUUGGCUUACCACAACCUCCGCCUCCCGGGUUCAAGUGAUUCUCCUGCCUCAGCCUCCCGAAUAGCUGGUAUUAUAGGCACACGCUACCAUGCCCAGCUAAUUUUUUUUAUUUUUUAGUAGAGACGGAGUUUCUUCAUGUUGGCCAGGCUGGUCUUGAACUCUCGACCUCAAGUGAUCUGCCCACCUUGGCCUCCCAAUCUCCUGGCUUUCUUUUAUAUAUAUAUGUAUAUAUAUAUGUGUGUGUGUGUGUGUGUGUGUGUGUGUAUAUAUAUAUAUAUGUAAAAUUAUACUUUAAGUUCUAGGGUACAUGUGCACAUUGUGCAGGUUUGUUACAUAGGUAUACAUGUGCCAUGUUGGUGUGCUGUACCCAUUAACUCGUCAUUUACAUUAGGUAUAUCUCCUAAUGCUAUCCCUCCCCCCUCCCCCCACCCCACAACAGGCCCCGGUGUGUGAUGUUCCCCUUCCUGUGUCCAAGUGUUCUCAUUGUUCAAUUCCCACCUAUGAGUGAGAACAUGCAGCAUUUGGUUUUUUGUCCCUGCAAUAGUUUGCUGAGAAUGAUGCUUUCCAGCUUCAUCCAUGUCCCUACAAAGGACAUGAACUCAUCAUUUUUUUAUGGCUGCAUAGUAUUCCAUGGUGUAUAUGUGCCACAUUUUCUUAAUCCAGUCUAUCAUUGUUGGACAUUUGGGUUGGUUCCAAAUCUUUGCUAUUGUGAAUAGUGCUGCAGUAAACAUACGUGUGCAUGUGUCUUUAUAGCAGCAUGAUUUAUAAUCCUUUGGGUAUAUACCCAGUAAUGGGAUGGGUGGGUCAAAUGGUAUUUCUAGUUCUAGAUCCCUGAGGAAUCGCCACACUGUCUUCCGCAAUGGUUGAACCAGUUUACAGUCCCACCAACAGUGUAAAAGUGUUCCUAUUUCUCCACAUCCUCUCCAGCACCUGUUAUUUCCUGUCUUUUUAAUGAUCGCCAUUCUAACUGGUGUGAGAUGGUAUCUCAUUGUGGUUUUGAUUUGCAUUUCUCUGAUGGCCAGUGAUGAUGAGCAUUUUUUCAUGAGUCUUUUGGCUGCAUAAAUGUCUUCUUUUGAGAAAUGUCUGUUCAUAUCCUUUGCCCACUUGUUGAUGGGGUUGUUUUUUUCUUGUAAAUUUGUUAGAGUUCUUUGUAGAUUCUGGAUAUUAGCCCUUUGUCAGAUGAGUAGAUUGUAAAAAUUUUCUCCCAUUCUGUGGGUGCCUGUUCACUCUGAUGGUAGUUUCUUUUGCUGUGCAGAAGCUCUUUAGUUUAAUUACUUCCCAUUUGUCAAUUUUGGCUUUUGUUGCCAUUGCUUUUGGUGUUUUAGACAUGAAGUUCUUGCCCAUGCCUGUGUCCUGCAUGGUAUUGCCUAGGUUUUCUUCUAGCGUUUUUAUGGUUUUAGGUCUAACAUGUAAGUCUUUAAUCCAUCUUGAAUUCGUAUUUGUAUAAGGUGUAAAGAAGGGAUCGAACUUCAGCUUUCUACAUAUGGCUAGCCAGUUUUCCCAGCACCAUUUAUUAAAUAGGGAAUCCUUUCCCCAUUUCUUGUUUUUGUCAGGUUUGUCAAACAUCAGAUGGUUGUAGAUGUGUGGUAUUACUUCUGAGGGCUCUGUUCUGUUCCAUUGGUCUAUAUCUCUGUUUUGUACCCGUACCAUGCUGUUUUGGUUACUGUAGCCUUGUAGUAUAGUUUGAAGUCAGGUAGCGUGAUGCCUCCAGCUUUGUUCUUUUGGCUUAGGAUUGACUUGGCAAUGCGGACUCUUUUUUGGUUCCAUAUGAACUUUAAAGUAGUUUUUUCCAAUUCUGUGAAGAAAGUGAUAGCUUGAUGGGGAUGGCAUUGAAGCUAUAAAUUACCUUGGGCAGUAUGGCCAUUUUCACGAUAUUGAUUCUUCCUAUCCAUGAGCAUGGAAUGUUCUUCCAUUUGUUUGUGUCCUCUUUUAUUUCGUUGAGCAGUGAUUUGUAGUUCUCCUUGAAGAGGUACUUCACAUUCCUUGUAAGUUGGAUUCCUAGGUAUUUUAUUCUGUUUGAAUCAAUUGUGAAUGGGAGUUCACUCAUAAUUUGGCUCUCUGUUUGCCUGUUAUUGGUGUAUAAGAAUGCUUGUGAUUUUUGCACAUUGAUUUUCUAUCCUGCGACUUUGCUGAAGUUGCUUAUCAGCUUAAGGAGAUUUUGGACUGAGAUGAUGGGGUUUUCUAAAUAUACAAUCACGUCAUCUGCAAACAGGGACGGUUUGACUUCCUCUUUUCCUAAUUGAAUACCCUUUAUUUCUUUCUCCUGCCUGAUUGCCCUGGCCAGAACUUCCAACACUAUGUUGAAUAGGAGUGGUGAGAGAGGGCAUCCCUGUCUUGUGCCAGUUUUCAAAGGGAAUGCUUCCAGUUUUUGCCCAUUCAGUAUGAUAUUGGCUGUGGGUUUGUCAUAAAUAGCUCUUAGUAUUUUGAGAUAUGUCCCAUCAAUACCUAAUUUGUUGAGAGUUUUUAGCAUGAAGGGCUGUUGAAUUUUGUCGAAGACCUUUUCUGCAUCUAUUGAGAUAAUCAUGUGGUUUUUGUCUUUGGUUCUGUUUAUAUGCCAGAUUACGUUUAUUGAUUUGCGUAUGUUGAACCAGCCUUGCAUCCCAGGGAUGAAGCCCACUUGAUCAUGGUGGAUAAGCUUUUUGAUGUGCUGCUGGAUUCGGUUUGCCAGUAUUUUAUUGAGGAUUUUUGCAUCGAUGUUCAUCAGGGAUAUUGGUCUAAAAUUCUCUUUUUUUGUUGUGUCUCUUUUCCUGGCUUUCUUAAGAAUCCCCCCAAUCACCUUUUGAUUAGAAAUAUUUCAACAAAAUAAUUUUAGACCAUAUCCUAUAAGGGGAGAAAGGGGAGAUCAGGGUCCUUAGAUGACAUUGCAUUAGAGAGUGGGAGCUAGAGUAGCAUGUCUUUGGUCCUAGAAAAUUUUCUUGCUCUCUCUGUUUAGUUAGACUCUUUUAGUUUGCAGGGUACAAAGAUUUAGGCCUAACUAGCUUAGAGAAGUGGUGUGGAGUAGUGUAGGAGACUGAAUCAUUGGUCUCAAUUCCUCACUCUCCUGUAGUAGUUUUCUACGUCUUUACCCUGCCAUAACCUCAUGUGAGAUGGGUUUUUGUACCUGCCUCUUCAUUUUGGGCAUGGGUAUAUGACUUACCUUGGCCCAGUGGGAUGUUAGUGGACAAGACAAAAGCAGAGGUUAGUAGUAUGCUUGGGCUGAUGGGCUUAUCCUCUAGUGCCUCUGUCAUGACUAUGAGAAGAAAAACCCUGAAUUGCCACAGCCUCUUCAGCCUGUUUCUCAUUGUGAGACCAUACAGCAGAGCCACCUGAGCCGACCUGAACUUAAAGCAGUGCCAGCGCAACUCAGAUGCCUGAGUGAAAAUAAAAUUCUUAUUGUUGUAUGACACUGAGAUUUUGUGGUCUGUUGUUCAGCGUUAUUGUGGCAAUAGAUGAUGACUAACACAUUUAUCCUGCUGGAUCCAGGACAACUCCAGGGGCUUUCAUAAGCAGGUUUUCUUGGAUAGUCUCUCUAGGAUUUUGCCAUUUACACCACUCCCUAUGGGUCAGCCUCACCCUUCUUUUCCCACCUACUGGCUUCCUCAUCCUACCUGCUGCUACCUGCCUCUACUUUAUAGCUUCUGCUUGCUUAUACACUAUGCUCCCUCUUACUUUUUCCAUGCCCAAGGUCCCUCCCUCAUGGCUCCUCCAGGGUCUCUGAAUUUCAUGACUUCUCAGCGUUUACUCCUAUUGCUUAAUGCUUUAUUCUUUUGGUACAUUCCAUUUCAAAUUUGAGAGAGUCUAUUUUGCCCAGCAGGGUUUUUUUGGGUUUUUUUUGGUUUGUUUUUCACUACAGAAAUGUCAUCAGUUGCUGGCCUGUUCAGGCAUUGACUGCUCUUGGGUUAGGCAGUCCAACUCUGGUCAGUUAGAUGUGUCACUGCGUUAUUAAUAGGAGGCUAUCCUUUGUACACGUUAGUGUCAUUAUGACUUACUUUGGGAAGUGAGUAUUAAAGCUUGUCAGUUUUCAGUGUGAUCAGUUCCCCACUUACCAGAGAGAACUUUACUUUUGCAAGCUUUUAAUUUUCUGAGGCUGCAUACCAUUUUUUUGUUUCCUAGUUCCAAGAUACUAACCUUAUGGUGUGAACUCUUGGGAUGAACCUUUGUCAAUGAAAAGCAUGAGAGAAGAGACCCUCUACUGAAAGGAAAGCUGAUUCAUCUGAAAGGCUUGCUAAUUAUUCCAAAAUCCUGAAUAAGCUGACUUAUUCUCUUAUCAACUCCAAAGAGAAGAAUAAAAUAAGUCAGCUCAUUUGGAAGGUUUAGGCUACUUAGGCUAUCAGAUAGUAUUUCUGUAACAGAAGAGAUUGGCCAAUUUAAAGUUAGUUUAUAACAAUUACAAGGCUAUGCUUAAUUAGAGUUGUCUCUAAGUAUUUCUCUAAGUAUGUUUUUUGGACACUAUUUUAAAUGGUACUUUAAAAAAUGUUAAUUUGCAAUUGUUUCUUGAUAGUAUGUUGAAAUGUAAUUGAUUUUUAUAUGUCAAUCUUAUAGCCUAUGACCUUAUUAAAUUAUAGUUCUAGAAGCUCUUUUUAUAGAUUCUUUGGAAUUUUCUAUGUUAUGAUUAGUUAUGUCAAGUGCAAAUAACCAUUUUAUUUCUUCCUGUUUACUCUUUAUGGCUUCUGUUCCUUUUUCUUGUCUUAUUGCACUGGCUAGGAUUCCUCCUCCUCACAUGAUAUUGAGUCAGUGUGAUGAAAUUAGAUGUCUUUGUGUUGUUCCUGAAUUUAAGGGAAAAUAAUUCAUUCACAUUAACUAUACGUUUUUUGUCAAUGCCUUUUAUCAAGUUGAGGAAGUUACCUUUUGUUCCAAAUUUGCUGAGAGUUUUUAUCAUAAAUGGAUUUUGAAUUUUGUUACAUGCUUUUUGUGUAUCACGAUGACCAUGGGGUUUUUCCUUUGGUCUGUUGAUACGGUGAAUUAUAUUGACUGAUGUUUUUGAGGAUUGACUCACUCUUGCAUUCCUAGGAUAAAUCUCACUUGAUCUUGAUGUAUUAUUGUUACCAGCAGGUCUUUGUUCUUAGAGCUCCCAAGAUGGUGGUGGGCCGCUCCCAAGAUGGCAGCAAGCCUUUUGUUCUCUGACCUGGGGUUCUUGGCCUCACAGAUUCUAAGGAAUGGAACCUUGGCCCACGCAGUGAGUUCUAUAGCUCUGUUAGAAGCCAUGGGUCACGGAAGAGAACCGUGGAACCCAGAGACUAGCAUUCAGCUCGAUUAGGAUGAAUCCAGGCACUUAGCUGUGCAGGAACAAUGGUGAGCCUCUAGCCCGAUCAGGAGUGGCAAUGGGCACCUCGCUGGAUCAGAAGCACAGCGGACACCCUGCCGGAUCCGGAGGGGUGAAAGUCAACGGCGGGUCUUGUGACGGCGUUCAGCAGUAGUUGACAGGGAGCGAAAGCUCAGCUUGAGCCGGAACAAACACGGACCAGAAGAGUGUGCAGUUGCAAGAUUUAAUAAGAGUGAAAACAGAGCUCCCAUACAAUGGGAGGGGACCCAAAGGGGGUUGCCACUACCUGCUCAAAUGCCUGGGUUUAUAUCCCAGUCAUUGUCCCUCCUCCUGUGCUCUCAGGCGAUAUAUGAUUUGACUAUUUCUUUACCUCCUGCUUUUAGCCUAAUUUGUAUUUUAGUGAGCCCUCUUUACUACCUGAUUGGUCAGGUGUGAGCUGAGUUAUAAGCCCCGUGUUUAAAGGUGGGUGCAGUCCCCUUCCCAGCUAGGCUUAGGAAUUCUUAGUCGGCCUAGGAAAUCCAGCUAGUCCUGUCUCUCAUUAUCUUUUUUAUAUAUUGCAGGAUUCAAUUUGCUGGUACUUUGUUAAGGAGUUUAAUGUCACUUGUUUUGAUCUUUGUCUUUGGUUGAUGGUUUCUUGUAUUUGCUGCGUUUGAUGUCAAGGUAAUGCUGGCCUCAUGAAAUGAGGUGGGAAGUGUCCCCUCCUUUUCUCUUUUCUGGAAGAGUUUAUGUAAAAUUGAUAUUAUUUCUUCCUUAAAUACAGUAAAAUUCACCAGCGAAGUCAUCUGCGCCUGGAGUUCUCUUUGUUGGAAGGCGUUUAACUGUAAAUUUACCAUCUUUCAUAGGUAAAGGACUGUUCAAAUUCUCUGUUUCUUUUUUUUUUUUUUUUUUUUGGUGAGACGGAGUUUCACUCUUGUUGCCAAGGCUGGAGUGCAAUGGUGCGAUCUUGGCUCACUGCAACCUCUUGGCUCACUGCAACCAGGUUCAAGCAAUUCUCCUGCCUCAGCCUCCCGAGUAGCUGGGAUUACAGGAAUGCUCCCCACGCCUGGCUAAUUUUGUAUUUUUAGUAAAGACGGUUUCUCCAUGUUGGUCAGGCUGGUCUUGAACUCCCAACCUCAGGUGAUCCGCCUGCCUCGGCCUCCCAAAGUGCUGGGAUUACAGGCGUGAGCCACCACACCUGGCUACUCUAUAUCUUCUUGAGUGAGCUUCGGUAGCUUUCACUUUUGUGGAGUUAUUCAACUUAUCUAAGUUCAAAUUUAUAUACAGAAAUUUGCUAAUAAUAUUCCAUUAUUUUCCUUUAAUGUAUACCUCAUGAUGUCUCCUCUUUGAGUCCUAAUACUGGUAAAUUGUGUCUUUUUCCUUUUUUUACUUGAUCAUUCUACUUAGAGGUUUAUAAAAAACUCGCUUUGGUUUCUUUCCUUUUCACGACUUAUUUUUCUGUUCUUAAUUUCAUUGAUUUUCGUUCAUUAUGAUUUCUUCUGCUUCCUUUGGGUUUAAUUUGGUCUCCAAUUUUAGUUUCUUAGGUGGAAGUUUAAUUGAUUUGAGGUCUUUCUUCUUCCCUAAUACAAGCUUUAAUGCUAUAAACUUUUGUCUAAGCACUGUUUAAGUUGCAUUCUGUAAAUUUUCAUGUUGUUUUGAUUUUGAUUCUAUUCCAAGUAUUUUCUGGUUUCCCUUGUUACUUCCUUUUUGAUCCAUGUAUUGUCUAGAAAUGUGUUUUAUUUUUAUUUAUGGAUUUUCCUGAUAUCUUUCUGUUAAUUUCAAAUUUAAUUUUUUUGUAGUUGGAUAAUAUAAUUUUAAUUCUUUCAAAUUUGUUGAGGUUUGUUUUAUGGCCAAGAAUAUAGGCUGUAUUGGUGAACGUUCCAUGUUCACUUGAAAAGAAUGUAUAUUCUGCUCUUGUAGGGUGAGGUGUUCUGUAAAUGUUAAUUAGGUAAAGUUGGUUGUAGUGUUAUUGGUAUCUUCUAGAUAGAAAUUUUUUUCUACACACUAUGGAUUACCAGAAGUGGAGUGUUAAGUCCACUGUUAAUUAUGGAUAUGUGUAUUUCUCCUUACAAUUCUGUGAAUUCUUACAUCGUAUGCUGUUAAGCUCUGAUGUCAGGUGCAUACAUAUUAAGGAUCGUUAUAUCUUUUCGAUGAAUUAACUCAUCAUUAUGUGAUGUCUCUCUAUUGCUUUCAAUAUUUAUUUCAAAUCUACUUUGUGUAAAUUUAUGUAACCUCUCUAGCUUUCUUUUGAUUAGUAUGUGCUUGGUAUCUUUUUCCAUCAUUUUACUUGUAACCUAUCUAUGUUUUUAAAAUGGAUUUCUUAUAGAAACAUAUAACUGGGUAUUGUGAUAAUCUCAGCCUUUUAACUGGUAUGUAUAGACUGUUUACAUUUAACAUAAUUAUUAAUAUGGUUGAAUUUAAGUCUGUUAUCUUGCCAGUUGAUUUCUAUUUGUCUCUAACCUGUUUCCCCUUUCCUCUUUAUUCCUGCUUUUAGAUUGAGGGUUUUUUAAAAUUCAAUUUUAUCUCUAUUAUUGAUGUAUUAGUUAUACCUUUUUAUAAAAAUUUAGUGAUUGUCCUUGGAUUUACAAGAUACAUCACAACCUACCUUCCCAUAUUAUACUACUUCUCAUAUAGUAUGAGAUCCUAACAAUACAGUAUAUUUCCAGUUUUUCCUCUUCAUCCUAUAUGAUAUUGUCAUACAUCUUACUUUUAUAUUUUUUAUAAUCUCUACAAUACACUGCUACUGUUUUUGCUUUAGGCAGUUAUCUUUCAGAAUGAUUAAAAAUGUGAAAAAAAGAUCUCGCAUUGACUUCUGUUUUUGCCAUUUCUGGAGGUAUCCACUUCUUCAUGUAGGUCCUCAUUUUUGUUCAGUGUCAUAUACCUUCUACUUAAAGAACUUCGUUUACCAUUUCUUGUAGUGCAGGUAUGCCGACAUUGAAUUAUCUUAACUUUUAAUUAUCUGAAAACUGGUUGUUUUGCUUUCAUUUUGGGGAGAUAUUUCUGCGUUGUGAGGUGUGUUUUUUUUUUCCUUCAUUACUUUAAAGAAUUACUCCAUUGUCCUCUGGAUUGCAAAAAAUCUGAUGAGUAGUCUGGUGAAUUUUUUAUUUUAAUUUUCUUCUUCCAAGGUAAUGUCUUUUUCCUCCCUCUGGCUGCAUUUAAGAUUUUCUGUUUAACUUUGAUUUUUAGCUAUUUAACUGUGAAGUGUCUCAAUGUGUGUUCUUUAUUGUAUUUAUUAUAUUUAUUUGUGUGCUUGUUUAUAUUUAUUCUGUAGGGUUCUCUGGGCUUCUUGGAGCUGUGAUUUGAUGACUUUAUUUUUGGAGAAUUCUUAGCCUUUUUUUCCCCCCUGCCAAAUACUGUUUCUGCGUCAGUCCCUCUAUCCCCUUCUGCCAUCUGGGACUCCAGUUACAUGUAUAUGAUGCCAUUGAUCAUAUCCCACAGCUCUCCAGCCUUCUUUCUGUGUUUCCCUCCACUUCUUUUUCCCCGUUUUUGUUGCAGUUUGGGUGAUUUCUAGUGACCUAUCUUCAAGUUCGAUUACUUCCUUGACUGUGUAGAGUGUUCUUAUGAGCCCAUCAAAGGAACUUUUAAAUCUCUGAUGACUUAAAAAAAUUAUACCAUUUCCAUUUGAUUCUUUGUCACAUAUUUCAUCUUUCUGUUGAAGUUUGCCAUCUGUUCAUACAUAUUGUCUACUAAAUUUUUUAACAUAUCAAUUGUUGUUAUUUUAAAUUUCCUCUCCAAUACUUACAACAUCUUGGUCAUCUUUCUUAGUUUGGCUCUCUUGUUUGGUUUGUCUUUUGAUAUGGGUUCUUCCCUGCUUUUGCUUUUUCAUAUGCCUUAUAGUUUUUGAUCGACUGGUGGACAUUACUGUAGAACAAUAGAGACUGAGAUGGACAUUAAAUAUUUAUGUUGAGACUACUACUGUUACAUUGGUAUUGGGGUUUGCAGGGAGUCAUAUUUGUGCAUAUAGAAUAUUCAGCACCUGUUACAGGAUUUGGAGUAUGACUUUACUAUUUUCAAUUAUUAUAAAGUUUCACAUUUCCAUAUUGUUUCCUUUUAUAAUACCCUAAAGAUUUAUGUUAUCAAGAAUUUCCCCUUGGAAUUGCCUACUCCUUUAUUUCUACUCACCGUGUCCGAAACUCUUCCUUAGUUAUAUCAGCUCUUGCAUCAAAUGACAUUUGUUAGCAGAUUUGUCUUUCUCAUGAGACUGAUUUCUUAAAAGCAGGUAGUGUUUUGUUAGUAUUUGGAUAUGUAGAUUCUUUAACUACAUUUUAGGUGUAGGUUUUUUUUUUAAGUAAUUGAAUUGAGUUGAGAUUAUUUAAUGAUUUUUAGUCCUUAGAAACCCACACUGCCCCUCCCACCAACAGUUUUUGGGAAGAUUGUCUCUGUGUUUCCACAGUCAACUGUGAUGUAUCUUAAAAAUGCACUCAAGUAAGAAGUGAGGGCUGGCCAUGGAUGAAUUUGUGAGGAAGUUGCUUUUAUACAGAGAAGACAUACAUUUUCUCUCCUAGUUAUCCAUGUAUGUUUUGUGUCCCUACCUUGACAAUAAGGUUUUGAGGGAAUAGCUGUCUUCUGCUUCUCCAGUAUUCCCUUUACUACUAGCACAAUGCUGGCUAUACAGCAGAUGCUCAUUAAAUAUUUCUUCACAGGAUUUAAUGUGACUAAUGGAUUUUAGAAGAAGGUACUAGUAGAUUUACUUUUUCAGUUUGCUCCUUGAAAACUUCAAGUGGUGAUAAUGGUGAUUUUUUUUUUUUUUUGAGAUGGAGUCUCGCUCUGUCGUCAGGCUGGAGUACAGUGGCAUGAUCUCGGCUCACUGCAGCCUCCGCCUCCCUGAGUUCAAGCAAUUCUCCUGCCUCAGCCUCCUGAGUAGCUGGGACUAUAGGCACGCACCACCACACCCAGCUAAUUUUUGUAUUUUUAGUAGAGACAGGGUUUCACCAUGUUGGCCAGGAUGGUCUCGAUCUCUUGACCUUGUGAACCGCCUACCUCGGCAUCCCAGAGUGCUGGGAUUACAGGUGUGAGCCACCGUGGUCAGCUGAUAAUGGUGAUAUUAUUUCAUUAUGGCAGGCCUAUCAUGUGCAGCUAAGAAUGUGGACUCAGCAACCAGACUGCCUGGAUUUGAAUCCUAGCUUAGCUACUUAUUAGAUCUGUUAUCUUUGGCAAGUUACUUGACCGUCUUGUGCUUCAAUGUCCUCAUCUAUACAAUGGGAACAAUAAUAGUACCGUACCUAUCUCAUGGGAUGAUUAUGAUGAUUAAGACAAAAUGCAGUAAAUGUUAGCUGCUGCAUUCUACCUUAAUUAUUAACAGUGAAUAUUAGACAAAUCCAAUUUUAAGUUCUUAGAAGAUAAGUUCUUUGAGUAGAAGGACUUUAACAGUGGAAAGCCAUCUAUCAGUGUGGAUAAAUAUAACUACUACUUCUGUAUUAAUUAAGGAAGUAACCACCUUUGCUUGGAAUAUUAACAGCAGAAAGGGAGCAGAGCUGAUUAAUUUCAACUUUGCUAGCAAUAAUGUUGUCUCUUCUGUCUUACCUUAGGAACAAUCUGCCCUAUUCCUAGGGGAAUAAGAUCAAUAGAGAAAUAAAUUUCCCAGAUUAGCUUUCACUACAACCAAAUGUACUUCAUUUUAUAGCUUAUUUUGAAUUGUAUGUUAAAACUAUAUUCAUUCUUACCUAAAGGUAAGACAUCAUUUAUUGUUGUUUUUAUAGUGUCUCCUUUUUACCAUUAUUGGCCAAAACAUGUUCAAUAGAUGUAUUUUUUGUUGUCUUUUCCUUUUUUUUUUUUUUUUUGAGACUGGGUUUCACUGUGUCACCCAGGCAUAAUCACGUCUCAUUGCAACUUUGACCUCCCAGGCUUAUGUAAUCCUCCUGUCUCAGCCUUCCAAGUAGCUGGGACCACAGGCAUGCACCACUACACCUGGGUUCUCUAAUUUUUUAUUUUUUUUUAGAGAUGGGGCGUCCUUAUGUUGCCCAGUAUGGUCUUGAUCUUCUGGGCUCAAGCCAUCCUCAGCCUCCCUAAGUGCUAGGAUUACAGGGGUGAGCCAAUCAAGAGAUGUGUAAAGCAAAGAAGGGAGUCACAGAAAGGUGAGUUUAGCCUGGUAAGACAUAUUUGGCAGACAGCUGUUGGGAAAAUAUUGUUAAGGUACAAUAUUUUGGAUUCACUAUUUUCUUUACCCAACAAGAAAGGAUACAAAGGACAGUUACAGAGCAAAACAUAAACACUCUUUGCAUAGCUUUGGUGCCUGUAUUGCCUGCUGAACCCCUUUAUCAAAAUAGUAGUUUAUAGCAUUCGAACAGUGCCAUCUUCUAUACAUGUAGUAGACUGCUGUUUUCUUAAGUUUUGAAAGGAAAUUGGUGAUACACUUGACCUAUGAAUCUAUGAUAUAGUCAGUUAAUGUUUUAACUACACUGAUACCAAGUAUGAGGUGAUAAUAGCCUGACCUAAGUUGGGAAUAGUGGAAAUGGAGAAGAGAUUGCUGUAAAUGUACUUUAAAAAGCAAAACAAAACAAAAACCCAAUUUUUUUCUUUUAUUGUACUAAAGAUUAUUUCUUUGAUUGUAUAAAAAUAUAUGAGUGUUGGAAAAGCUUGAAAAGUAGAAAGAGGCAAGCUGUUGAACUCUUAGAAAUAUAUAUAUCAUGUUUAAAAACAUGUUUUAGUGGUCAGUUUCUUUGAAUAAUUUUCCUAAGGGUAAGGAGGUUGGAAAAGUUCAGUUUGGUAUCAAGACAUCUUGUUUAUACUUUGAUAAUAGAUUUUCAUUGCUUAGUGGAAAGCACACCUCCAUAGGAAUGUGCAGAGAAUUUCUGCUGACAAGGAGGUAUGCUUAAAACAUCUCACGUAUAGUCUUUAGAGACCACUAGUAUCAGAUGUUUUUGUGUUUUACAGAUGUAGGCCUUCUGCAGUUUUUCAUGCCUCAUGGACGGUGGCCAGACUUAGGACUGGUUAUGAGUUCCUGUCUCUUGUUUCUUUUAGCCUUUUAAGAUUUUUUUUUUUUUUUUUUGAGACAGAGUCUCACUCUGUCGCCCAGGCAGGAGUACAGUGUUGUGAUCUUGGCUUACUGCAACCUCUACCUCCUGGGCUCAAGCACCUCUCCUGCCUCAGCCUCCUCAGUAGCUGGGAUUACAGGCGUGAGCCACCACGCCCAGCUAAUUUUUGUAUUUUUAGUAGAGAUGGGGUUUCCCGCCACUGUUGGUCGGGCUGGUCUCGAACUCCUGACCUCGUGAUCAGCCCACCUCGGCGUCCCAAAGUGCUGGGAUUACAGGCGUGAGUCACCACACCUGGCACUUUUUUUUUUUUUUUUUUUUUUUUGAGAUGGAGUCUCGUUCUGUUGCCCAGGCUGGAGUGCAGUGGUACAAUCUUGGCUCACUGCAACCUCUGCCACCCGGGUUCCAGCGAUUCUCCUGCCUCAGCCUCCCGAGUAGCUGGGAUCACAGGCACAUGCCACCACACCCAGCUAAUUUUUAUAUUUUUAGUAGAGAUGGGGUUUCACCAUGUUAGCCAGGCUGGUCUCGAACUCCUGACCUCAGGUGAUCCACCUGCCUUGGCCUCCCAAAGUAGAUUUUUUUUUUUUCUUUCUAAUGGGGGCCUUGCUAUGUUGUCUAGGUUGAUAUCCAGCUCCUGGGCUCAAGUGAUCCUCCCACCUCAGCCUCCAAGUAGCUGGGAUUACAGGUGUGCAUCUCUGCACCCAGCAAGAAAUUUUUUUUUAUUAUAGAAAAUUUCUUUCUUUCUUUCUUUUUUUUUUUUUUGAGACGGAGUCUCACUUUGUCACUCUGUUGCCCGGGCUGUAGUGGAGUGUGGUGGUGCGAUCUCGGCUCACUGCGACCUCCACCUCCUGGGUUUAAGUGAUUUUCCCACCUCAGCCUCCCGAGUAGCUGGGAUUAUAGGCGCCUGCCCCUACGCCCAGCUAAUUGGUUUGAACUUAACAUUCCUUGGUGAUUGUUACCUAAAUAAUUAUUUCACUAUUGCUACAUUGUAAGAAGAGCAAACUUUCAUCUUGUUAAUAAGUAACACGGAAAUUUUUUAUUAAAAAACUUUUUUAAAAAACUGUGAGGAAAUUCAUUUAUUCGCUAUACACCAUAUCUUUUUAUGUGAUUAUGCCUUGUAAAAGAGGUAUCAUUGUGAUAAGAAUGUUUAAAAGUUGUAGUUUGCUAAAUUAAGUGCUCCUCUAUUUGUUUUUGAAUGUGUUAUUUUUAAACAGUUUUAUGGUAACAGAUUUUGAUCUAGAGUCGUGUUUCUGCAUUAUGCAUUUGUGGUUUCUGGCUACAUUGGGGGCGUGGGGGGCUUGCUCCUUCAAUAAAGGAAAAUAAAAUUCUAAAGUUUAUUUGGUUGAGGAGUAUGAAUCAUGGUGAAGACUGAAAUCCAUAUAGGUCAUUUAUUCUCACUGCUGUUAUCACGUAUUUUUUCUAUAACCUAGGAUGGCUGUUGUUUAAAUAUCAAUAUUUAACCUCAUGUAGUGUUUUCUAUGUGCCAGACACUGUACUUUGUAAUUUGCAUCUACUAAUUUAUUUAAUCCUUAUAUGAUUGUCAUGUUUUGUAGAUGGGAAAACUUGAGUUAAGGAGGUUAAGUGAUUUGCUCUGGCUGUGUGGCUAACAACUAGCAAGGGCUAAGAUGUGAACCCAGACAGUUGAUUAUAGAAUUUGUACUCCAAGAGAGGGAGAGAAUGGAUUGUCUAGUGUCUCUAUUACUAGAAAAAUAACUGAAGUGUACUGACCCACUAGCCUUGGAAGAUAAUCUGUUUAUUCAACAUACAAUAAUCUACACAUAUAUUUGUUUUGUUUAUUGUGUUUGCUACACAUAUAUUUAUUUUGUUUACACAUAUGUGUAGUGUGUGUAGACACACACACACUACAUGUCCACGUAAAGGAGCAAAUGUUUAGCGCUUUCCCUUUGGAAAGUCCUUCUUAAUGUAUAACCUUUUUUUGAAUCUUUUUACUUGACCUUAGAGCAGAAAUAGCCCCCAGAUUCUAUAGGAGAAUCUUUGAGGUCAGAGUAGAUGGAAAAAUCAAGAGAAACGUAGCAGACAGCUUGAGGUCACAGAUUCACACAGGAUACCACUCUGACCUUUGGACUCUAUUUGCACUGAAGUUAAAGCUGCUUGUUACAAAGCGGCCACCCAGAUAAAUCUUAGCUAUAUAUUUUCAGGCUAUUUUUGGAGCAGAAAGCCAAAUAGCUGGUAUCCAAUACCAAAGAAACAAUUUUUCAAAUUCUCCAAAUCAUGAUAAAUAGCGGCCACAAGUCUCUGUAGAACCAAGCCAGGAGAUACUAUAGAGACUCUCUCGUUCUAAGUUUAUUUCUGCUGUCUCUUUGCUUAGUGAUUUUUUGUUGUUGUUGAAGUAAUGUAUCUUAUAUUUUAACAAAUUCUUAAAUAAUUCUCUUUCCUUCCUUUUCUGUCCCUCAUUCUGUUUUUACUUUAGCAUGUGUAUUUAUUCUACCAAAUGUUAGUUCAGAUGGGAGUUGUAGAUAAUUUGAGCAGGCAUGUUUUUCACAAAAAAGUUAACCACCUUUCUCUUUCUCUGUUUUUAUGUUUGGAUGGUCCUUCUUUUGUGUUGGUCUGAUAAGAGGUUAAUCUGUGUGGGUGAGAACAUGACUACAUCCUCAAGAAUCUGAACAUUGUAAUAACAAUCUGAUGGUUUGAAUAGUUGGAUGUUAUUGAUAGGGAUAAAAUGGAAAAAGAUGAGGGAGCGUCCUCAGGUCUGGUGCUGACUGAGGUGUACUCAUCUUGUGUGUUUGAGUCUGUGUUUGAAGUUUCUUUUUUUGCUGGGGGGAGACAGAGUCUUGCUCUGUCGCCCAGGCUGGAGUGCAGUGGUGCGAUCUCAGCUCACUGCAACCUCUGCCUCCUGGGUUCAAGUGAUUCUUGUGCCUCAGCCUGGGACUACAGGUGCAUGCCACCACGCCCAGCUAAUUUUUGUAUUUUAGUAGAGGCAGGGUUUCACCAUGUUGGCCAGGCUGGUCUCGAACUCCUGACCUCAGGUGAUCUGCCCGCCUUGGCCUCCCAAAGUACCUGGAUUACACAUGUGAGCCACCACGCCUGGCCUGUGUUUGAAGUUUCAGGUGGCCUGUGCCAGUGGUAAAACUUAACAGUAAAGGCCUCAAGGGAUUGAUUCGCUACAUAUAUAGUGGGGAUGAGCUUAAAGACAACGUAUUUCUUACUUUUACUUAUUCUGUUUACAAAUUCAAAUAUUGAUGCUGUAUAUUAUUUUGGUAAUUAUUAUUACAGGGCUAAUUUUCUUCAUGUACAGAGAAUUUCUUCAAGUACCUAACAUGUUUUGGUAAAGAUGUUUGUGUCUUCCUGCAAAAACAUUUCCUGAAUCAUUUUCCUGACUUCUGUGCAGCUUUUCCUUUUUAGUAAAUUUUGCUUGAAGAAAAAAAAAGAAUUAAUUUUUCCUCUAUAUUAAAAGAAGCUUUCUUUUUCAUCUAGAGAAUAAAUAACUCAGUAAAUAGAGAUGAUAUUACUGUUUCUUCAAAAUAAUUCAUUUCCCAAAGUUUUUUUUCAUGGUAUGUAGUUUUAGGGAAUGAGUCAUAGAAUUAUGGGAUUUUAUGGCAUAGCAUCUUUAGAAAAGGAUUUUUUUUAUUUUGGCUUCACUUUAUAGUUGAAAAAGAGUUGAUUCUUUAGUUUCAUUAAUGACUGUCCUGUAUAUCUUCUCAUGUUGGUUGUUGAGUGAGGUGACCAGCUCCUCGGAGGGACAAACCAUACAAUGAAAGGGAGAAAUUUGAGAAAUGAUUGGAUUUGGUGUAGUGGAAAUUCAAGAUGAAUAUUAUGUUGGACAUAUUAGCACAAUUCUGGGUGCGUUAAUGGUGUUUUUUGUUUUUUGUUUUUCUGUUGGGGUCGGUUCCAGUGUGGGGCUGAACUGUCCUCUGGAAGGUUGACUUCUCAUGUCUGGUCUGUGUGAGUGGAUGGGCCCUCCUUUGGCACCAGUCUCUUAAGUAUGCAGUUGCAGCCAGUUGGUAUUCACUUGGUAUUUAUGACAUGAACCAUAGCAGGUGCAUAUGUGAAGAAAGCUUGAGGUUUCUUUUCACAAAGUUAUUGAUGUUUGUAUAAAUAUAUAUUUUUACUGGCCAUCUUAUUGUUACCGGUAGAGGGUGUCCAGGUUCUUGGUGUUUUGAACAAAGAAUUGAACAAAAUGUACAAAGCAAGGAAAGAAUUGAACAAAAUGUACAAACAAAGCAAGGAAAGAAUGAAACAACAAAAGCAGAGAUUUAUUGAAAACGAAAGUACACUCCACAGGGUGGAAGCAGGCUGAGCAUAGGGGCUCAAGGGACCUGUUACAAAACUUUCUGGGGUUUAAAUACCCUCCAGAGGUUUCCCAUUGAUUACUUGAUGUACACGCUAUGUAAAUGAAGUAGUGGCCUGCAAUCAGAGGCUGAAGUGAAGUUACAAAGGUCACAUUCCUAUGCAAACACCUGAUUGAUUGGGGAAAGCAACCAAUCAGAGGCUAAAGUGAAGUUACAAAGUUACACUCCUAGUCAAAUGUCUGAUCGGUUUUCCCUGGGCCACAUGGAAAAGGAGGGGGCUUUGCAAAGGGUGUAGCCUUCGAUCCUUUUGUUUGUAUGGAAAGUUGGGGUUUUCCUUUGGCUUUAGCUGUAGGCGUGAAUCGGCCUUAGGUUCCCUGCCUCAGGUUCCCUGCCUCCAGACCCUAUUUUCCUACCUCAUUAUAAACUCUUUUUCUUGGUUCUCAUGGUUUUGAAGUUAUUUCUUAAGGGCUUACAAGAUAAAACAGCCACAUCAUAUAUAAAUAAGAAUUUUGUGUUUUUCUUUCCAGUUUAUAUUACCUCAUAAUCGUUCUGCAUAUUCUUUAGACUCACUGAUAGCUGGCAUUUUUGUCUUGGUCCCAACUUGUUAACAGGAGUGCCUUUAGUAUUUCAUCAUAAGGUUUGACUUGAUUUUGAUGAAUAUUUGUGAGGGUUCAUACUACUUUAACCUGAUAAAGUACCUUAGUUCAGCUUUGACUUUGUAAAUUAAGGAGUAUACAGAACAUGGAAGGUUCAGGAGAGAGCAGAAAAUGUAUGAGUGACUAAAUAAUACCCAAGUAGAGGAGCUAGGAACCUGGUAUAUUUAUCCCAGAGAAGAAAAAACUAGGGGAUGAUUUCAUUAUCUCCAAGUAUAGGUAGGACCCAUGCUGGCAUUUUGGAGCUCCCACGUCAUCUUUGAGAAUGAAAAAACAGUUCACUUUUUUCCCUUGGUAAACUUUUUAUUGAACAAUAACAUACAAAGAAGUACAUAAAAUUUACAUUUUAGAUGGUUUGCCUCUCCCUCUCCCCACCCCCUGUCCCUCUCUUCCUUCCUCCCCCACCCCCACUUCCCUUCCCUCUUCCUCUUUCCCUUUUCAGUGUAGUGAUAGCUAAAAAUAACAUUUGCUUGCCUGAGGGCAUUGCCGACCUGCAUUUAGGAGAAAGUUAGAUCCACUAUUUAUCUGAACAUUGAGUGAUGGGUCCUUGCUUUUACCCAUGUGCUUAUAAGGAUCAGGAAUCCACUCUUGCCCUUUUCCCUGUGGUCUCUAAAGGCCCAGAGCUGGGAGUUUGUUUGUUGGAUCUGGGGGCUGCAGUAGCCCUUACCUGAAUUGAUUUCUCUAGAGCUGCCUUAUGGUCAGAGACCCCUCCCGUGGUGAAAUGUAGAGUGAACUACCCAUGUUUUCUCUGUCUUCACUUCCAGUCCUUGCUUACUUUAUGAAAUAGAUUGUCAAACUUUCAUUGAUAUUAUACAGUCUCUUAACUCGCAUGGCUCUUAGGUUUUUAAAGCUUAGGUCUUGAUGUUUGUUUUUGUUUUUUUCUUUUUGCAUUGUUCUCCAGUUACUUGUGUGCUAGUGUUACCUUCCUUACUAGAUCAUAGGUCUUAACCCUCUUUCUUGGGUCACAGAUAUUUGUAUCACUUACUCCUAAUUUGGAACUUUCAGAAUUUAGCCCUUCUUUGUCACUUGGUCUGGAUGUUUACAUGGUUUAAUCACAAUAAUCUGCAAUAUUGUUUUCCCAGUUAGGGUUGUUGUGUAACAUAAUACAUGGAGGCUAAAAAUCAUGGAAUUUGAGAAUUUAGGUUGCAUAAAAUGGGUAGUUCCAAUGUCAAGAUCUUCAUUCAUUCAUCAGAUAGUUACAGAGCACCUUCUGUGUGCCAGGCACUAUACUAGGUAAUGAAAGGUAGUGGCGAGUAUGACACUGCCUCAAACUUCAUAGAAUUUAGAAGAGUUUAGUGAAAUGUCCUUAAUCUGUUCUAGAUUGGUGGUAGUAGAAUGGUCUUGGCCUGGUGCAGUGGCUCAUGUCUGUAAUCCCAGCACUUUGGGAGGCCGAGGCGGGUGGAUCACGAGGUCAGGAAAUCGAGACCAUCCUGGCUAACAUGGUGAAACCCCAUCUCUACUAAAAAUACAAAAAAUUAGCUGGGCGUGGUGGCGGGCGACUGUAGUCCCAGCUACUCGGGAGGCUGAGGCAGGAGAAUGACGUGAACCCGUGAGGCAGAGCUUGCAGUGAGCCGAGAUCGUGCCACUGCACUCCAGCCUGGGCGACAGAGCAAGACUCAGUCUAAAAAAAAAAAGGGUCUUGAGCUUUAGAAUUAUACUGUCCCAAGUACAGAUCUAAGCUCUCCUAGUUAUUAAAGUUGAAUAACUUCAGAUAAUUAUUUAUACUCUGAAUGGGAUAAGAGGACCUUUUUCCCAGGGUUAGGGUUCAGAUUUAAUUGGUAAAGGUGUGGUUGUAGCCCAUUGGGUGGCAGAGGAGUUCCCUGCUUGCCUGGGCCAGAGUUAAUACACAGUUGCUGGGCAAGCAAGAAACCAAACCUGAUGGGUAGGCAUGCAGAAGGGAGUUGGGUGCCGCUGUGGCUACAAGGUGCAGAGGCAUGCAGAGUCCGCAUUGGGAAGGCCCUGUUAAACAACGCUUUGGGUUCCAGAUGAGCCAGGCCUGGUAGCUGGGCAUGCAGAGGGAAGUGGUACAUGGCAUCCUUUUUAGGAGGGCUGCAGGAAACAACUCUCUGGGAUACAAGCCAGCAGAGGCCAUCAGGAGGCUAUUGUGUGUGUGAGGCCUGGAGUCCCUGCUGUCCGUGUCUACAGGAGCACAGGAAGGUGGUCACCAGGCCUGGUGUCACUGAGGGACCAUGUGCUUUGUGCUUUGUGCAUGUGGUAGGCAGAACACUACCAUAUGUCCCCACAUACUUACACUAGACCUUGGAGCAAGAGCAAGAACAGCAAAAGCACAGCGCUUUUGAACCCAAAAGACAAGCUCCCUUCUUCCUGCGUUGUCCCUCCAGCUGCCUCUGCUGACCAGGUUUAGCAUCAUGUGCUCUGUAAAGGAGGAAUUCUGGAGAGUCCAGUCCAUUAUUACAGAGCUAGUACUGAAGGGUGAGUUUGGAGUUAAGAGGCAAUAAAUUGAUAACUGGCACAGAAGCCAAAUAUAAGAGUAUUGACUAAAUAAUAGCUAAGUACAAGAACACAGAUUACAUAAUUCCACUUUUAUAAGGCACAGGACAGGUAAAACUAAUCUACAUUGUUAGAAGUCAGGCUAGUGGUUACUUUUGGGGAAAAGCAGUAUUGAAAGGAGUAUGGAUUUGUAGUGCUAAUGUUCUGUUUCUGGAUGGGGAUGCUGGUUACACAGCUGUGUGCAGUUUGUGAAGAGCUGUGCUUUCUAUUAUAAUGUCUAUUAUAUUUCAUUAAAAUUUAAAAUAUGGUGUAACCUGAUUCAAAAAGUAAAAGCUUUAAAACAAGAUCCAGUCUAGAAUAGAGGAAAUAUAAUCCAGGGUAUCUCAUCCUUUUUUUUUUAAUGUUUAAAAACCAUAUGAAGGUUGUCUAACUUAAUGUCUAAAAAUAGAUAUCUAAUUCAUUCAACAAAAAUACUAAUGGCCAAGGAGUUUGAGACCAGCCUGGCCAACAUGAUGAAACCCGUUUCUACUAAAAAUAUAAAAAUUGGCCAGGUGUGUUGGCGGCACCUGUAGUCCCAGCUACUCGGAAGGCUGAGGCAGGAGAAUCACUUGAACCGGGAGGUGGAGGGUGCAGUGAGCUGAGAUCGUGCCAUUGCAGUCCAGCAUGGGCAACAGAGCAAGACUCUGUCUAAAAAAAAAAAAAAAAAAAAAAUUAAUGGCCAGACUUCCUUUCUUUUGGUAUCAAAUUGGUAACUCUGAAGCCGUCAGUAGAGCAACUUACACUUCUUCAUUUUGCUGUCAUUCUUCUUACCAAGACUUUAAGCAGCAACUUCUAAGCUUUUUUAUGGCCUCACAGAUACCUCUUUGUUCUUGGUCUAAAUAAAAUAUCACUGCUGUCUUCUGUAAGCGUUGUCUUUGCUUUUAUCUUUGUCAUGAUAUAUCCUUCUCACAGCUGACAAAUCACCAGACCUUCUUUUUCUUCACUAAGAGAUUUGGAAUCCCACUGUAACUCCCAUAUAGGAGUUAAUGAUAACAACAACUGUAGACUUGUUUGGGAACUGGUGGUGAUAGGAGAGACUCAGUGUGUAGCUUUUAAAAGCUUCAAGCAGAAGCAGCUCAGUACUGUUAUUUGUUCAGGAGUAGGUAACUCUGAGAGCAGAAGCUAAGGAAUCUACCAAGUUAGCAGUUGAAUCUGGAUCCAAGGGAUGGAUAUGGAAUCUAGAAAGAGUUCAUGUUCACAGAAAACAGAGGUUGUUAAGAAACUCUGGCAUUACACUGUGAACAGAAUUUAGGGUGAAUUUCAAAGUGGAGCCAGCUGCUUAAAGCUCAGUUGUUAAAGUGAGUCACAUUAGUCUAAUUCCACUUUUGUGGACAGAGCUUGAUAUCUCCCAGUAUACAGCAUAUGAGGUUGUUUUGUGCUUUCAAUAGCUGGUGGUAUUCUUGUACAUAGAGAGGAUUUGGCCAGGGCAAGAGUUACUGCAAACAUAUCACAGAAGGCUGAGAAUCUAGAAUGACUGCCUUGUAAAAAUUGUUUCCUUAUAAUCUUUAACCCUUAAGUCAUUUGGGGGUGAAGGAAGAAAACAGCAUAAGUGGUGAAAUUAGCCAGUGGGCCCCUCAUAUAUAAAUUCAUUCCACCUACUUGCCCAACUAGUAUAUGUGUACUGUACUUACAUUAUUGGUCUGUCCUAGAUACUGAGUUCACAAAGGUGAAUCUGGGCAGUUCCUUGGCCCUCUGAGUGUUAUUAUUUUAUAUUCCUCUCUUUGAGGGCUGCCUGCAUCACUUGUCUGUGAUACCCAGCUUUGCACCAACUCCUUGAGGAUUUUGAUGAGCCUUUAAGAAUUGAUACUUGGGUUUCAUAUUCAACCUAAUGAGAGUUCACUGACUUUUAAUUUAUUUCAUUUUAUUAUUAGUCUGGGCUUGUACUGCCACCAGUAAAGACUGUCAUUUUCAAAUUUAACAUCUUGAGAAAAGGUGCCUAUGAUUGAAGAUAUGAGUCUCAUUCUGCACAUGUAUUCUAGAGUGGCAGUUUGGAAAUUUGUUGUACUCCAAACUGGUCAUCUGUAUCUAGAAAAACCUUAAAUCAUGCCAUUGGAGCUGGUUCUCAGUGCUUGGACUGAUGAUGGAAGGGAACAUUGGAACAGGUAACAUAAAUACAGUAGUCCCUCAGUGUCCAUGGGGGAUUGGUUCCAGGACACCCAUCCCAUGCCAAAAUUUGAGGUUGCUCCAGUUCCUUAUUUAAAAUGGCAUAGUAAUUGCCUAUAACCUACUCACAUCCUCCCAUAUACUUUAAAUCAUCUCUGAUACAGUAUAAAUGCUAUAUGUAAAUAGUUGUUGUACUGUAUUUUAAAAAGUUGUAUUUUUAUAUUUUUAAAAAUUUUAUAUUUUAAUUGCCUUAUUGUUAUUAAAUAUUUUUGAUCUUUAAUUCUGAGGAUGUGGAGGGCUGACUGUAUAUGCAGGAGGUGAUACAUGGUAAGAAGUUAAGUUUAUGUUAUAAAAUGGUUACUUUUUGAUCUGGAUAUUGGUACUGUUUACCAAGAAACAAACAGGCUUUAUUCUGUGAUUCUUGUGCUCAUUCUGGGCAUGAAUUCUGUCAUCUCUCAGACCAGUCCCCCUAAAGUAGUGCCCCAUGCCAAUCUGAAAACUUCACUUUUAGGCAAACAACUAGUUUUAUUUAGGUAUUAGAAGUUAGUAGUGGUUUGCUAAUAUAGUAUGAGUUUAAAGUAGGUGACCAAGUCUGUACCAAUUUGUAGGCAAAUUAAAUGAAUCACAUAUGGUGUAGAUGGUGUUAACAGAUUUUUGUGGAUGGGCUUAAGUUGGCCUAAAGUGGCCUCCUAAAUAUUCUGCUUAUUGCCUGCAGUUUCUGCUUUUAGUGUACUACAACCAGAUUGGGAGAACCAGGACAUUUUUUGUUUGGCAGGAGGAUCCUAUUGCUAGCCACCUGCCUCAUCAUUCACCCAGAGCUUUCUGUUUGCUUUUGCAAGGAGAACUUUUUCCAUACCUCUUGGUCACCUCAUGCCAUGUCCUGCUCUAUGUAUUUUCCCCAACAGACUAGUUUUGUGUUUACCUCAGUACUCCCUCCCUCUUAGGCUUCUAGGAAGGAGGAAUUGGAAGUGGGAGGGGAUUAAGAACUGAUACUCAUCUUUGAAAAAUCCAGAGUUUGAAAAACAUUCUCAAUUUAUAUUAAACAAAAAUUCUCAGACCCUAAGGAAAGUGCAGGAGGUGCCAGAGUUGAACAGCUCUUAGGAGGCAGAAAUGACUGUGGAAGCCAUCAGGGUGCAGCAUCCUUCUUGGUUUGCAAAGGUAAUUUGAUGUAGGAUGUGGAAGUAGGUUUUAGCAUUUCAUCCAUAAAACCUGAAUGGAAGGAAUUUGUGUCAGAUUCAGAAUCCAUUAUGUGUCUUCUCUUUAAACAAAGGGAAAAAAACACUUUGGAAAAAUAUUGGGUUUUUAAAAAUUUUACUUUAAUACAGCAGAGUUAUAGGAGGAAGCCCAUCUUUUUAUUGCUAGGAAUUCCACAGGUUUGGUUGAGGAGCUGUUUUCCAAUUAUAGAUUGACUUGCCACUUGGGCCAACUCUUCUGUUUUCUGUAGAUUGAAGAGUGCUGAGCCUGGGCAACCAUAAAUAUGUGGUUUUUCUUUUAUUAAUUAUCUCAAAGUACAAACUUUUCUCUGCUAAGUAUUGUCUGUUAUAAUUUUGUUAAUGUGUUUACUUUGUUUCCCUGCCAUCUUGGAUAGCUAUCAGAUAAACUUUGUUCCUUACCAUAAAUUGAUCCAAAACAAUUUUGUUUAACAAUUCAGAAUUCAAAUGGAGGGCUAUAUGAAUGUAGAUAAAGAAUUUAAACAGAAUUAUGUACGGUUAUAUCCCUCAAGAUUUUAUCUGUGUUUAAUUAUAUGAGUUAUUUGUUUGAAAUAUUUUGUUUCCUUGUAUCAAGUAAUAUUAUCUGAAGUAUCUAUCUAUCUUGUCUAAAAUGUGCUUAUAUGGUCCUUUUAAAUGAUAGUUUUAUCAAGCUAUUUUAAUUGCUUUCUGUGUACUUCACCCUUGGAUUGAAACCAUCCUCUGCUACAGCCUUGCUUUUUUACUUUUAUUCUUUUUUCUCUUUACAUAUUUUCUCAGAAUAUUUUGGAUUUUUAGCCAUGUAGAGUAUGAUUUUCAGUGUUUGUCUCCAUCCAGUCACUCAUGCUGUAGACAUCUGUGUAGUUACAGGGAGAGGUUUAGGAGCCUGCAAGCCCGCCUCAUAGCAGCCUUGUGUUCCUUCAGGGAGUGCCAGUCAAUCUUCCUGGGUUGGAGUCCACAUCCAGCAAGGUCAUUUUGUCUGUGGCCUGGAUGGGGCUUAUUGAGCCCUGUGAACAUAAAAUUAGCUCCUUGGCAUGCUGGUAAGCAGCAGAACUGAGCAGAGCCCAGGCACGUUAAGAGUUUCACAUGGGAAGAGCAUUUGACUUCUCUCUUCCUGUGUUUUGGGAGGGCCUGGUACCAAAUGCUCACCCCCUUUUUUUUUUUCAUCAGUACCUGAACCACAAGCCACCAUGGACGUGCACACUGAUACCUACUUGGGGAUCAGGAGAGUGUACAUGACAACAGCAAGGGAAGCAGCAGCACAGGAGACAGGCAAGACCACCACUACCUUUGCUGGAACUACACAACCAAGGAGCCAUGCUUAAGUCUCCCCCAGGGUGGUGGUCUCCCUUUCCAAAAACUUAACAGCUGUCCCUGAGCCUGUUCCUGGGGUACACAAUCAUAAACAGUGUGUGUAUGCCUGCCCCAAGUGGCCAGUGAUGGUCAUCAGGCUAGACACAGUGACCGAAGAGCUGUAGCUUGACCCUUGAUAAGGGGGACUUAAGUGCUUACUGGUUAAGGCACUGUGUUGUUACCACUUUACAGGCAGGAGCCUCAGAGAACACCUGCCACACAUAGGCCAGACCUGAUGGCGCAUCACACCAGGGUACAGUCAAUUAACAACAGAGUCUUAUCUUGGGGACAAGUGCCUUUUAGGGUGGGAAGAGAUGACAACAUCCAACAAAGACAGUUAAGAGCUGUGUAGGCCAUAGUGCAAGCCCAGCAGCAACUGGUGAUUCUGUCCCAUGUGGCCUUCACCAUAUAAUGGAACUAGUUAGUUAGCUAAGAGAAAUAAGUUGAAACUAACCAGGUGUCCUUGGUCACGGUUGGGCCCUCUUGUUCAUGAUGCUAUUUGCUUUAGUUACCUCCUAUUCACCCCAUUUGUGUGAGAUUCCUGACACAGGAUUAUAGGGAUGACCAAGCACAGUACACCUAACACUGGGCAGAUGAGAUCAGCAGCAGUUUAUUGUUCACGUACACUCAUAGCCUGCGGGAGGAGACACCACACACCACCCAGGGCCACACAGGGAUUGUACUUGGGAAAAGGGUGAACAUCCAGGGUCUAUGGGAGGCAGGCUUUGUAGUACCAAGAGGACGGGGUGACCCCUGGUUCCCAUGGGAGGAUGUGAUUGACUUGCAUGAGUAAUUCUACAGGCUGGCAAGAAAUGGAAAUCCUCUACUUGGGCAUAAGAAGGAACUGCACAUGGUCCCCUCAGUAAGGAUGGAGGUUUGGUUAGGGGACCUUAUCCACAGGAGCAGAGUGGGGAAGGGAACUUGGGGAUAGACCAUUGGAGGUCUUUCCAGUUUCAGAUACCAAGGCAGCACAUAAUAUUGGGCCUGAAUUUUAGGCUUUACACCACACAAACCAUUGUGUGGGACUUUGGAGACUUUUUUCCAUUCCCCCCAAAAGCUAGUAGUUAUCCCUUCCCUCACUAUCUCACUGCCCCUUCAUUUUUCCCCCUACCUACUCUCUAAUAAGUACUAGAAAAUGCAAUCUGUCAGGGAGAGUACAUGGCAUAGUGAUUUCAUGGUUGAGUUUCUGCUCGGAUGUUUUUCCAGAGUAGAGGUCCUCCAACCUGGCUGCCUAUUAGAGUCAUCUGAGAGAGUUUAGAAAAUUAUGUGGGGUGUCACCUCAGACCAGUUAAAUUGGAAUCUUUUGGAGAUGGGAGUGAAUUUUUUUUUAAUGUGCUUCAGCCAUUAUUGAGAACUGCUUCUCAUGGAUGUCAGCAGAGUCACCAUGUCUAAAACCAAAUGCGUUGUCUUACUCCAUGGAGCCAGCUCUUCCUGUUGACUGUUUUUCCCUCUUAAUGGUACUAAUAUCAUCUUCCCAGUCUCCCAGGCUAGAAAAGUUAGAAUUCUCUUUGUACUUGUUCUCCCACUUUCCAUAGAAUGAUAUUUAUCAUUGGUCAGCCUUUGUUAAUUUCAUUUCAUCUUUACUGCUGCACUUCUAGACUGUUGUAUUUGUAGAAUACCUUUCCAACCUCUGCCCACUCUCUGAGCGCCCCAAAUAGAACAUUUCCAGUCCUGAUCUCUCACUUUAUUAUUUUCAUUUGUCUGCAAGGCAGCUUGAUGUAGUACUAAGAGAGCCGAAUUGGAAUCCAGGAAAUCUAAUUAUUGUACUUCGGAGUCAAUGUGAAGCUUUGGGCAGAUCAUUUGACAGCUCUAACCCUAAGUUUCAUUAUCUUAAGAUAAAAGGAUUACAUUGCCUGAGCCUUGGAUUCUUUCUCACUGUGACUCAGUCUUCACUUUUCCUUCAAAUUUAGCCUGUCUGUAAUAGAACUUAUCCAUCUACUCUCCCAAAAGUUACCUCUUUCUCGUGCCCUGAUGCCUCUUGCCAAUACCAGCAUUCUAGCAUCUUAGGCCACUUAAAAAGAAUCCAGCUGGGCGCGGUGGCUCACGCCUGUAAUCCCAGCACUUUGGGAGGCCGAGGCGGGUGGAUCAUGAGGUCAGGAGUUCAAGAGCAGCCUGGCCAACAUGAUGAAAACCCGUCUCUAUUAAAAAUACAAAAAUUAGCCGGGUGUGGUGGCAGGCACCUGUAAUCCCAGCUACUCGGGAGGCUGAGGCAGAGAAUUGCUUGAAUCUAGGAGGCAGAGGUUGCAGUGAGCUGAGAUCGCGCCACUGCACUCCAGCCUGGGUGACAAUAGUGAAUCUCUAUCUCAAAAAAAAAAAAAAAAUCCAUUAUCUUCAUUUUCUUGGACUCCAUGACUUCUCUUCUGUUUUAUUUGCUAGCCUGCUGUUUACUGUUACUUCUACCUGGGUAUGACUCACUGGUCUUCUUGGACCCCAAGCCUGCCCUACCUAUUCCUACCUGAUGAAUCUUUACAUCAAACAAACUUUGAUAAUUUUUGUCCUUUUCUCAGAAAUCUUCAAUUAAUGGCUCCCCAUUACAUAGAAGAUUCAAUUCAAACUGCCUAGCCAGGCAUUUUGAGAGCCUCUCUCCAUCACUUAUCUCCAGCCCCAAACUUCACCUGCCUUUGCUGAUUCCUCUUCACCUAUUGGUCACCCAUUAUACAUGUUGGGUGUUUAGAAAACAAUUUUUUAAUUGAAUUACUCAUUAACUUUGGAUUAACAUAGCCUUUAAGUAAGAUUUUUAAAAAUUUUAUUAACUUUUUUCACACGGAAAAAUGUCCGCUUUCUGGUGAGGAAUUCUUUGAGUUUCAGCAAAUGCAUACCGUUGUGUAAUGAACAUCACAAUCAAGAUAUAGAACAGUUUCAUUAUCCCCUAAAAUUCUCUUUAUAGUUGACCCUCUCCUGUCCCCAACCCCAACCACUGGUAUGUUUUUUGUUCCUACAAUUUUACCUUUUCUUGAAUGUCAUAUAAAUGAAAUCAUACAGUAUAUAGACUUUUCAAUUUGUCCUCUUUCACUCAGCAUAAUGCAUUUGAGAUUCAUCCAUGUUGUGUGUAUAAGUAGUUUGUUCUUUUUUAUAACUCUGUUUUUAAAAUACCCCCAAGAGGGAGUUUACAUUGGGAGUUGUGAGUUUUUUGUGUCUUAUAUGCUGUUUUGGAAAACGGGAAGAGAAAAUGUCAUCUAGAUCAUUUUUAGCGCCCCAAAACAUGUUUAAGCUAUUUUGUAGAUGGCUUCUCAUUUCAAUGUUAACAGAGUAACUUUUUGUUUUUAGCCCAUGUGUCAGUCUCAUAUGAUUGGCUUUUGUACCAGUUCUGUAAAUGAAGAAACUGAGACCCAGGGAGAUCAAAUAAGUUGCCCAAAUCCCACAACGCUUGUGUUCAGAACCCAGAUAUCUUCACUCCCAAGUCUACAGGUACUGCUGUUCUACCACAAAAGACAUUAAAAUGUAAUGAGUGAAAAGUUCUUGUGUUACUGGUGAGACCUCUUGAAACUGAAUAUAUAGAGUGUUGUUUGUAAAACCCUUUGUCUUCCCCCAUAAGAUUAUGACUUGAAUUUUCAGGGCUCUGAAGCUUGAAUGGGCUUGGCUGUCAAGAAAUUGGUUUAUUCAGUCCUGUGUUCACAGCUGUGUUCAUUCCUGAUCUGGGUCAAUUGACAUUAUGACAUAGGGACCAACAACAACAAAAAAGUACAGUCAGAUUUUACCUUACAAUGUGAUAUAUGAUAGCUCUAGAAGGGUCUGGCCACUUGCUUCUACUGUUCUUCUUAAUAGUAAUUAUUAUCAAGCUAAUUGAUUUUUAUGAGCAGAUUAGGAUUUAGAAAUGAUUUUUUUCUGACCAAGGAAGAUGAACUGGAGUUGGUAUUUCUCCUCUUGAAUUGUGCGAAUGUGCCUCACUCAUCACUGAAAUCAAAGAGUUUGGCCAUGUGACCUCAGAGAUCCCAUUCAGUUCUGAUUGUGCGAAUGUGGCAUUGUUUGAGGUAUUUCUGGACUAUAGAAAGCUUCCUUAGUUUAUACCUUUAUAUCAUCUCAGGUAAAACAGGUUAUAGGAAUUAUAGCAACAUAGGAUACUGCUUCAAGUUAAUAGUAAUUACUUUGAAUAGCCAGAGGAGAGUCAUUCAGUGAGUAAAAGCCUUGUUAUUCAGCAGCUGGCCCACAGGAAGGUUCUCAGAAUGGGCUUUCCUAAUACUCUUGGUUCAGUAGUGAGAGUUUCUUAGGAGGUUGUUGUCACUUCUACUACUGGCUUUUGCCAUCUCCUCACAGACAAGGAUUAAAAUCACUACUGUUGAUUUGCCUUUUGGCUUAUAUUACCCACAUGCAGGGUAACAGAGCUUUUACUCUAAAAUUAAUUCGUUGAAUGUUUAAAACACUUCUUUUGAGGAGUAGAGUCUUAAUGUUAAUGAUGGUAAUGCAUCCUUUCAGACCGGCCAAGCACAGAGCUUCCUCAGUUUGGAAGUGAUGACAGUACUAGUGCCUUCUCACAAGUAAUAUUUGGCAGAUAUUUUAAGUUAGGUGUUCACAUUUUUGGAGAGAUGGAUUUUUAGUCCAAGCUUUACAGCUGUGUGUAAGAUCUUUCUCUUUUGACCCACUAUUGAUAAGUCCAUAUAUGCUAUUAGUAUAUUUACUAAUUUAUCAAAUACUAUGCUAAUAUUAGUUAGACAAUAGUCAAAAUAGAUACGGUCCCUGUCCUCAUGGCCCUCUUUUAAUCUUACAGAUAAGGAUAUUUUUUGACAUGUCGUCUUGAGUUUAAGGUGAUAGGUUUUCUCUAGCCUGUAGUAGAGAACAUCAGAAAUUUACCUAUACAGACUUUCUUUUGCCUGACUUAUACACAAAAGAUAAUUUUUCACCGAAGUUGAUCUAAUUUACAAAUUGCCGUAUGUUUCAAAGAAAACUUUUGGGCAUCUAAAAGAAUUCAUAAUACAAAAAAAAAAAAUCAAACCCUCAGUAUAUUUUGGUGCUCUGGCACCUUUAAGGCAAAAAUAUUCUCAGCCAGAGCUUGAAUAUAUGAGAAAUCCUUAAAACUGUUACAGAAGCCUUUCCUCAUGCUAGUUUGAGUAUUCUGGUUGUGCAGAAAUGUUUCCACUAGACCACAGGGUCAUCUUUGAAAGAAAAGAGUAACCAUUUGUCAUUUGAAUGCCCUUCCAUUAUUGGUUAGUUGACAUGAGUUUAGGAGACUAUAAAAAUAAAAUAUCAGAGCACACUCAAAAAAGAAUUAUUGAAUGUUAAAAACAUAUUAGCUAUAAAGAAAAAAGAAGGCUUGAAAGAGAAAGUUGAGGAAACUUCUCAGAAAGUAGAACAUGAAGAGUUUUUUUUUUGUUUUGUUGUAAAUGAGACAGAAAAUUAGAGGUACAGCCAAGAAGGUCCAUCAUUCAAAUAGUAACAUGAGUUCCAUUAAAAGAAAACAAUAGGGAGGGAAUUAUGAAGAAAUAAUACCAGAGGAAUUCUCAAAACUGAAAAAUCUGACAGUUUCCAGAUUGAGAAAGAAUCCACCAGGUACCUAACCUCAUGGGUGAAAAUAGCCCCAAGGCACAUCAUUUUGAAAAGAUGAUUCUAAAAGCUUUCCAAAAAGGAAGAGAUGUCACAUACAAAUGGGCAGAAAUCAGAAUUGUUCAGAUUCUUCAAAAUAAGUGGUGGAAGGAAUAGAACAAUGGAGUAGUGCUCUCAAAAUUCCAAGGAGAAAUUGACCUCCAGCCUGUGAUUUGCAACCCACCAGUCCAUCCAGAUAGAAUAGAAACAUUUUCAGACAUGAAGGUCUUAAAAACUUACAUCUCAUUUUUAGGAUUUUCUAGAGCAUUACUAGAUGUUGUGCUUCACUAAAAUGAGAGUGUAAACCUAGAGAGGAGAAACCUAGGAGUCCACCAUGGAGAGAGACUGAGGGAGUGAGUCUCUGGGAGGAUGGUGAGGAGAAGUCCCAGGAGGCAGAUUAGAGACAAUGAUGAAGGACUCCUGAUGGAGGACUCUACCUAUAAUGACCCAAGAGAAGAACAUUGAGCUUAGAUUGAAAGGAGUUUCAAGGUUUUAGAGGAGCAUUUUAGGAGAAGUUAGUGAUUCAUAGAAAACCAUGCAAAUUUUUAAAUGAGGUAGUUAUUAUCUUCAGGGAAAAAAAUGACACAAAGUUUCAGCAAAGUAUAGUUCAUGGCUUAGCUGUGAAUUAAAUGUUGAUUUAAUAAAUAAGGGUGAUAAUAACUAUAUUGGGAAGAUAACACUUCAUCUUCUAUAGUAGGAGGACUUCCUGUUUUUGAAAAAAAGUUUUAUUGGAACACAGCCAUACCCAUUUGUUUGCAUAUUUGUCUAUGGCUGUUUUCACAUCACAGCAGAAUUGAGUAGUUGCAACUGAGACCAUAUGGCCUACAAAGCCUAAAAUAUUUAUUAUCUGGCCUUUUUAUAAAAAUACUUGCUGACUCCUGUUCCAUAGGAAGAAGCCAAUAAAAUAAUGCCUAAAAUCGAAAAGAAAAUCUAAUAGCAGUAAUAACCAUGUUAUUUAAAAUAGAAUGGAAAGGAGCAGAAGGAACAGCUGAAGUUUAAAUGACUGCCUCUGGGAAUAGUGAAUCAGGAGUGGGGAGUAGAAUCGGGGACUGUUUUUUUUUUUAUUUGUUUUAGGCUUUAUAUUUCUAUUGAAUUCUUAAGCUAAGUACAUGUAUUUGAAAAGGUGUGAAGGAAGAAUACUGAGAAAUUUGAUUGGAUUAGGAGGAAAAAAAAAAGAGGUCACUAGUUACAUUGAAAGUAGUUCAAAGCCUUUUCAGUAAACACAGCUUUCCCAUUAAUUCACUUACUCAUUCCACAGGUAAUCACUGAAGAGUCCAAAUGUCAGGCACUGAGUGCUACACUGCAGGACAGGGUCCCUCCCUGGAGGGUGCUUGGGCCCUCCACAGCUAAUGGCAUGCACAGACAGAAAUAAAUAUCUUCCUUCAAUAGAUGAAAAUGAAAAUACAGAAAAAAGAGAAGCAGUUGUCAAAUUUAAAAGUUUUGAAUCACUCCCCAAUGUCUGAUGCCUCUGUCAAUUUUGACUACAAAUCUCCAUCCCCAUUUGACUGCAGCACUGAUCAAGAAGAGAAAAUUGAAGAUGUUGCUAGUCACUGUCUGCCUCAGAAGGACCUGUAUACUGCUGAAGAGGAAGCUGCUACCCUUUUUCCUAGGAAAAUGACAUCCCAUAAUGGGAUGGAGGACAGUGGAGGAGGAGGUACUGGAGUGAAGAAGAAACGGAAGAAAAAGGAGCCAGGAGACCAAGAGGGUGCAGCAAAGGGAAGCAAGGACAGAGAGCCCAAGCCAAAGAGGAAACGAGAACCGAAAGAGCCAAAGGAACCCAGAAAGGCCAAGGAGCCGAAGAAGGCCAAGGAGCACAAGGAGCCGAAGCAAAAAGAUGGGGCAAAGAAGGCACGGAAGCCCCGGGAGGCCUCGGGCACCAAGGAGGCCAAAGAGAAGAGGAGCUGCACUGACUCUGCAGCCAGGACGAAGUCCAGGAAGGCCAGCAAGGAGCAAGGACCAACCCCAGUGGAGAAAAAGAAGAAAGGAAAAAGGAAAAGUGAAACUACAGUGGAGAGUUUAGAGCUGGAUCAGGGCCUGACGAACCCAUCUCUGCGGAGUCCUGAGGAGUCCACUGAGUCUACAGACAGCCAGAAACGACGCUCGGGAAGGCAAGUAAAGCGCAGAAAAUACAAUGAGGACCUGGACUUCAAAGUGGUGGAUGAUGAUGGGGAAACAAUUGCUGUUCUUGGAGCUGGUCGAACAUCUGCACUCUCAGCCUCUACACUGGCCUGGCAGGCGGAGGAGCCUCCAGAAGAUGAUGCAAACAUCAUUGAGAAGAUCCUGGCAUCUAAGACUGUCCAGGAGGUUCACCCAGGAGAACCUCCGUUCGACUUGGAGCUGUUCUACGUUAAGUAUAGAAAUUUUUCCUACUUACAUUGUAAAUGGGCCACAAUGGAAGAGCUCGAAAAGGAUCCUCGCAUCGCACAGAAGAUCAAGCGAUUUAGGAAUAAACAAGCCCAGAUGAAGCACAUUUUUACGGAGCCUGAUGAAGACUUGUUCAAUCCAGACUAUGUAGAAGUUGAUCGCAUCUUGGAGGUGGCCCACACCAAGGAUGCAGAAACAGGGGAGGAGGUAACACAUUACCUGGUGAAGUGGUGCUCACUACCAUAUGAAGAAAGCACGUGGGAGCUAGAGGAAGAUGUAGAUCCUGCAAAAGUUAAAGAAUUUGAAUCUCUUCAAGUUCUCCCUGAAAUUAAGCAUGUGGAGCGGCCUGCUUCAGACUCCUGGCAGAAACUUGAGAAGUCUCGCGAGUAUAAGAACAGUAACCAGCUCCGGGAGUACCAGCUGGAAGGGAUGAACUGGCUUCUUUUUAACUGGUAUAACAGAAAAAACUGUAUUUUGGCUGAUGAGAUGGGCCUAGGGAAAACCAUCCAGUCCAUCACAUUCCUUUCAGAAAUAUUUCUGAGAGGAAUCCACGGCCCUUUUCUCAUUAUCGCCCCUCUCUCCACCAUCACUAACUGGGAGCGGGAGUUCCGGACAUGGACAGAGAUGAAUGCCAUUGUGUACCACGGCAGCCAGAUCAGCAGGCAGAUGAUCCAGCAGUAUGAAAUGGUGUACAGAGACGCCCAGGGAAACCCCCUUUCAGGAGUCUUCAAGUUCCACGUCGUCAUCACAACAUUUGAAAUGAUCCUAGCAGACUGCCCAGAGUUGAAGAAGAUUCACUGGAGCUGUGUGAUAAUUGAUGAAGCCCACAGACUGAAGAAUAGGAACUGCAAACUUCUGGAGGGUCUAAAGCUUAUGGCCCUGGUAAAGAAACUGCAGUCUAUCCUAAAACCAAUGAUGCUUCGGCGGCUGAAAGAUGAUGUGGAAAAGAACCUUGCUCCCAAACAAGAGACGAUCAUUGAGGUGGAACUGACCAAUAUCCAGAAAAAGUACUACCGUGCCAUCCUCGAGAAGAACUUUUCCUUCCUGACCAAGGGGGCAAAUCAGCACAACAUGCCCAAUCUCAUCAACACCAUGAUGGAGCUGAGGAAGUGCUGUAACCAUCCCUACCUGAUCAAUGGAGCAGAGGAGAAAAUUCUAGAAGAUUUCCGAAAAACCCACAGCCCUGAUGCCCCUGACUUUCAGCUGCAGGCCAUGAUUCAGGCAGCAGGAAAGCUUGUGUUGAUUGAUAAACUACUCCCUAAGCUGAUUGCAGGUGGCCACAAAGUACUCAUCUUCUCCCAGAUGGUGCGCUGCCUCGACAUCCUAGAAGAUUACCUCAUCCAGAGAAGAUACACCUAUGAGCGAAUUGAUGGGCGAGUACGGGGAAACCUGCGCCAGGCAGCCAUCGACCGGUUCUGUAAGCCAGAUUCAGACCGCUUUGUCUUUCUUCUGUGCACCAGAGCGGGAGGCCUGGGGAUCAAUCUCACAGCUGCUGAUACCUGCAUCAUAUUUGAUUCUGACUGGAACCCACAAAAUGACUUGCAGGCUCAGGCCCGAUGUCACCGCAUAGGCCAGAGCAAAGCUGUGAAGGUGUAUCGCCUCAUCACUCGAAAUUCCUACGAGCGCGAGAUGUUUGACAAGGCCAGCCUAAAGCUGGGGCUGGACAAGGCUGUUCUUCAGGACAUCAACCGAAAGGGCGGCACCAAUGGGGUACAGCAGCUCUCAAAAAUGGAGGUGGAGGACCUACUCCGGAAAGGUGCUUAUGGAGCCUUAAUGGAUGAAGAAGAUGAAGGCUCCAAGUUCUGUGAAGAAGACAUAGACCAGAUUCUGCAGAGGCGAACGCACACCAUCACCAUCCAGUCUGAGGGGAAAGGGUCCACUUUUGCCAAGGCUAGCUUUGUGGCUUCAGGAAACAGAACAGAUAUUUCCUUAGAUGAUCCUAACUUUUGGCAGAAAUGGGCUAAAAUAGCUGAACUAGACACUGAAGCAAAGAAUGAAAAGGAAAGCUUAGUGAUCGACCGACCUCGCGUGAGAAAGCAGACCAAACACUACAACUCGUUUGAGGAAGACGAGCUCAUGGAGUUUUCAGAGUUAGACAGCGACUCAGACGAAAGGCCCACGAGAUCCAGGCGCCUCAAUGACAAAGCCAGGCGCUACCUCCGAGCGGAGUGCUUCCGGGUAGAGAAGAACCUGCUCAUCUUUGGCUGGGGCCGGUGGAAGGACAUCCUGACUCAUGGCCGAUUCAAGUGGCAUCUGAACGAGAAGGACAUGGAGAUGAUUUGCCGUGCCCUCCUGGUGUACUGUGUCAAGCAUUAUAAGGGGGACGAGAAGAUCAAGAGUUUCAUUUGGGAACUGAUCACACCUACCAAAGAUGGGCAAGCCCAGACCCUCCAGAACCACUCAGGCUUAUCUGCCCCAGUCCCCAGAGGGAGGAAGGGGAAGAAGACGAAGAACCAGUUGCUAAUCCCAGAGCUAAAGGAUGCAGAUUGGCUAGCCACCUGCAACCCCGAGGUGGUCUUGCAUGAUGAUGGCUAUAAGAAACACCUCAAACAGCACUGCAACAAAGUACUUUUGCGAGUCCGGAUGCUGUACUACCUAAAAGCUGAAAUACUGGGAGAAGCAGCUGAGAAAGCAUUUGAAGGAUCUCCUGCCAGGGAGCUGGAUGUACCUCUGCCUGACAUCGACUACAUGGAGAUCCCAGUGGACUGGUGGGAUGCUGAAGCCGAUAAGUCACUUCUCAUUGGCGUGUUCAAGCAUGGUUAUGAAAGGUACAAUGCCAUGCGAGCAGACCCAGCACUUUGCUUCCUGGAGAAAGUUGGGAUGCCCGAUGAGAAGUCCCUUUCUGCAGAACAGGGUGUUACAGAUGGGACCUCAGACAUUCCUGAAAGAGGCAACACAGAUAAAGAAGACAAUGCUGAGGACAAAGUAGAUGGCCUCCAGAAACAAACGGAGAGUUCCAGUGAUGGAGGUGAUGGCGUUUUUAGCGAAAAGAAGGAUGACAGCCGGGCAGCCCAGGAUGGCUCCGACCCAGACAAAUCGCCCUGGCCAGUUUCCUCCGCCCUCACAGCUCGUCUCAGACGUCUGGUCACUGUUUACCAGCGCUGCAACCGCAAGGAACUGUGCCGGCCUGAAAUUCUGGGACCAGGUAACCAAGGAUAUUGGGUUCAGGAAGAGAUGUUCAGGAGAACCUCAGAAAUGGACCUCAUCAACAAGGAAGCCCAAAAGAGGUGGACUAGGAGAGAACAAGCAGACUUCUAUAGAACAGUGUCUUCCUUUGGUGUUGUUUACGAUCAAGAAAAGAAAACCUUUGACUGGACACAGUUCCGCAUCAUUUCCCGUUUGGACAAGAAGUCGGAUGAGAGCCUGGAACAGUAUUUUUAUAGUUUUGUGGCCAUGUGCCGGAAUGUCUGUCGUCUACCCACAUGGAAAGAUGGCGGUCCCCCAGAUACCACCAUCUACGUUGAACCCAUCACUGAGGAACGUGCUGCAAGAACUCUGUACCGCAUUGAACUGUUACGGAAAGUCCGAGAGCAAGUGCUCAAGUGCCCUCAGCUGCAUGAACGCCUCCAGCUGUGCAGGCCCAGCCUCUACCUCCCAGUCUGGUGGGAGUGUGGGAAGCAUGAUCGAGACCUGCUCAUCGGCACUGCCAAACAUGGGCUGAACCGCACUGACUGUUACAUCAUGAACGACCCCCAGCUGUCCUUCCUGGAUGCCUAUAGAAACUAUGCCCAGCAUAAAAGAUCUGGCACCCAGGCACCAGGAAAUCUCUGUUGCCUUUACCAGACCAACUCCAAGUUAUAUGAAUCUCUUACAUAUUCUCAAAUGAGUAGGACUUCAGAGUCCCUUGAAAAUGAACCUGAAAAUCUAGUGAGAGUAGAAAGCAGAGAUGAUCAUCUCAGCCUGCCUGAUGUGACAUGUGAAAACUUUAUUUCUAAAGUUCAGGAUGUCAUUUCCAUCAACCAUGAUGAAAGUCUGCUGCCUGAGUCCUUAGAGAGCAUGAUGUAUGGUAAGAAGGUGCUCAGCCAAGAACCAAGCUCUUUUCAGGAGAGCCCAAGUACCAAUACUGAAUCUAGAAAAGAUGUUAUUACCAUCUCAAUAAGCAAAGAUGGGAACUGCCAGUCUGGUGGCCCUGAGGCAGAAAUAGCUUCUGGCCCUACUUUUAUGGGUAGCUUAGAAGCAGGAGGAGUAGCUCAAGCAAACAUCAAAAAUGGAAAACAUUUGUUGAUGUCUAUUUCAAAGGAAGGGGAGCUCUGCUGCAGUGAGGCAGGACAGAGACCUGAAAACAUUGGCCAGCUGGAAGCCAAGUGUUUAGCUUCCCCUUCCUUGAAUCCAGGAAAUGAAAGUGGGUUUGUAGAUAUGUGCAGUCUUAGUGUCUGUGACUCCAAAAGAAACCUGUCAUCAGAUCAGCAAUUAAUUGAUUUAUUGGAAAACAAAAGCUUAGAAAGUAAAUUGAUUUUGAGUCAGAACCACAGUGAUGAGGAGGAAGAAGAGGAGGAAAACGAGGAGGAAAACUUAGCCAUGGCAGUAGGCAUGGGGGAAAGGCCAGAGGUAUUGCAUCUCACGGAGCCCACUACUAACAUCUCAAGGGAAAAGAACCAAGGCUUCCAAGAUGAAACCAAGAAAGGAAGCUUAGAGGUGGCAAACCAGACUCCUGGGCUACAGAGGGCUUUCCCCGCUCCAGCAGCCUGUCAGUGCCACUGCAAACACAUGGAGAGGUGGAUGCAUGGCCUCGAGAAUGAUGAAUUUGAAAUCGAGAAACCCAAGGCUUAUAUCCCAGAUCUGUUCAAAAGUAAAACCAAUACUAUCGCCAUGGAGGGUGAACCCACUGCUAUUCCAUCACAGCCGUUUAAAGUGAAGCAUGAGCUUUUAAAAGAACCUUGGAAAGAAAGUGCAGAGGGGCAAAACGUUUUCCCCACAUAUCCUCUUGAAGGAAGUGAGCUCAAAUCAGAAGACAUGGAUUUUGAGAAUAAAGAUGAUUAUGAUAGAGACGGAAACUGCCAUAGUCAAGAUUAUCCAGGGAAGUACUCUGAAGAGGAGAGCAAGAGCUCAACAUCGGGCAUCACAGGAGACAUUGGGGAUGAGCUACAGGAGGCUCGAGCUCCCACUAUUGCUCAGCUGCUACAGGAGAAAACUCUCUAUUCCUUCUCUGAGUGGCCAAAGGACCGCGUGAUAAUUAACCGCCUAGAUAAUAUCUGCCACGUGGUGUUAAAGGGGAAGUGGCCCUCUAGCCAGCAGUAUGAGCCCUCAGGCACACUGCCCACCCCGGUAUUAACCAGCAGUGCUGGUUCUCGAACCAGCCUCUCAGAGCCGGAAGCAGCAGAACACAGCUUCAGCAACGGCGCAGCAUUGGCGGCCCAGAUCCACAAGGAGAGCUUCUUAGCUCCAGUAUUCACAAAGGAUGAACAAAAGCACAGGCGUCCCUAUGAGUUUGAGGUGGAGAGGGAUGCAAAGGCUCGGGGCCUGGAGCAGUUCUCUGCCACCCACGGGCACACCCCUAUCAUCCUCAAUGGCUGGCAUGGGGAGUCAGCUAUGGACCUCUCCUGCUCAUCAGAGGGGUCCCCAGGAGCCACAUCCCCUUUCCCAGUGAGCGCCAGCACCCCUAAGAUUGGGGCUAUCAGUUCACUUCAGGGAGCCCUUGGCAUGGACUUGUCUGGGAUUCUGCAAGCUGGCCUGAUCCAUCCUGUGACUGGACAGAUUGUCAAUGGAAGCCUCAGAAGAGAUGAUGCAGCCACGAGGAGGCGGAGAGGGAGGCGGAAACAUGUUGAAGGAGGGAUGGACCUCAUCUUUUUGAAGGAGCAGACACUUCAGGCGGGAAUCUUGGAAGUCCAUGAAGACCCAGGGCAGGCCACCUUGAGCACCACACACCCUGAGGGGCCAGGGCCUGCCACCUCGGCUCCUGAGCCAGCUACGGCAGCCAGCAGCCAAGCCGAGAAAUCCAUUCCCAGCAAGAGUCUGCUUGACUGGCUAAGGCAGCAGGCUGACUACUCCUUAGAAGUUCCUGGCUUUGGGGCAAAUUUUUCAGACAAACCAAAGCAGAGGAGGCCACGCUGUAAAGAACCUGGAAAAUUAGAUGUCAGCUCCCUGAGCGGGGAAGAGAGAGUUCCUGCCAUCCCCAAGGAGCCAGGACUGAGGGGGUUUCUUCCAGAAAACAAGUUCAAUCACACUCUGGCUGAGCCUAUUCUUCGAGAUACGGGCCCCCGCAGGAGGGGGAGGCGGCCUCGGAGCGAACUCCUGAAGGCUCCUUCCAUUGUGGCAGACUCUCCCUCUGGAAUGGGGCCACUGUUCAUGAAUGGACUGAUUGCUGGGAUGGACCUGGUAGGACUUCAGAACAUGAGAAAUAUGCCAGGCAUCCCCCUCACCGGGCUGGUGGGGUUUCCAGCUGGCUUUGCCACGAUGCCAACAGGUGAAGAGGUCAAAAGUACCCUGAGCAUGCUGCCCAUGAUGCUGCCAGGCAUGGCUGCUGUGCCCCAGAUGUUUGGUGUUGGGGGACUCCUCAGUCCACCCAUGGCAACCACCUGCACUUCCACUGCUCCGGCGUCUCUAUCAAGCACAACGAAAAGUGGUACGGCAGUGACUGAAAAGACUGCGGAAGACAAGCCGAGUAGCCAUGAUGUGAAAACAGACACUUUAGCUGAGGACAAGCCUGGUCCAGGUCCAUUUUCUGAUCAGUCUGAACCUGCAAUAACUACUAGUAGUCCUGUGGCUUUUAACCCAUUUCUCAUCCCAGGAGUAUCUCCUGGACUCAUUUACCCAUCCAUGUUCCUCUCCCCUGGUAUGGGCAUGGCUCUGCCAGCCAUGCAGCAGGCCAGACACUCGGAAAUAGUAGGUCUGGAGAGCCAGAAGAGGAAGAAGAAGAAGACAAAGGGGGACAACCCCAACUCCCACCCAGAGCCUGCUCCCAGCUGUGAAAGGGAGCCCAGCGGUGAUGAGAACUGUGCCGAACCCAGUGCCCCUUUGCCCGCAGAGAGAGAACAUGGGGCACAGGCUGGGGAGGGGGCACUCAAAGACUCCAACAACGACACCAAUUAGAACUUUUUUCAUUUAAGAAAUUAUUGUGACUUGUAAGUUUCUUAUCCCAUAAAGGUUUGUUACUUCCCUCACUUCACCUCCAUAAGAACCUGUGUUUCCAUAAGUAAGAUUACGUACCUGAUUUCCUGUCUGAGAACUAUGGUAACAGAUGUUAAUAGUUGCAGGGUCUCACCACUUCAUUAGAUAAGUGUUGUCUACCUAGUCUAGGAGGCACAGAAUUCUCAUUCUGUUAUCCAGUUCAUUCCAGCAAUCAUAGUUAAUACAGUACUUGGUGACACGCCCUACCCCCUUCUCUUCCAAGUUUCCCACUCACUUGAGGAGGAAAAAUGGCAAAAGAAAGCUGUCUAGGGUUUUACCAUUGAAGGGUGGAAGAACAGAGACAAAGAGGAGCUCUUUUUCUGUGAGCUGGGUUGCACAGGAAGAAUGUCACAGGGAACCAAAAAGCACAGAAAAAGGAAGUGCUGGUGCAUAUUUUUGAGUUAAAAUAUUUCCCUAUUUUAUCAUGAUUACUAAGUGAGUAGUAUAGACAGAAGUAUAUAACUAAUGGUUGAAAAUACAUAUAUUCAUUUCUUUAUAAAAAACAAAAACCUUACCGGUAGUAAUAUAAUUUCCCCCUUGGUGGUUUUUCAGACACCUGCAGCAAGAAGAAAUACUGACUGACUAGGCAUUAUUUUCUAUACAUCCCUCUCACCAGUGAAAAGAUUCCUCUUGCUGCGAGAAAGCUUUACCCACCAUGAGUUAUUGCUGUCGACGGGGGUGGGGCAAGGACCCGCGCUCCGUAGAGCUACACGCUGCUUCACAAGCACACGGCUAGCGCUCUGCUCUCACCUGGUUCGCUUACAGAUUUCUCUAGCCAUUAAUUUGCCUCUCUGUGUUUAAAGAGCACCAGGACCGAAUGGAUUUUCACUUCAGGCUUUCCUUCACCAAGAAUAAGGUUCUUUCUGGAGCCUGCAAGAAGACAGUUGCCCAACACUUUGACACUUGCUAGUAGGUCCUUUGAUCAAGAGUGUCUGAGGCUGUCAAAUGUGUGCCACCCUUUAUAAUACAGCUAUGAAAAGUUACUUCUCCAUUAAUUUCUCCAUUCUGUUUAUAUCUUACAGUUGGACCCAAAUUCCAAAUUAUCAGUUAAUCGAAACUACAUUGCAAGUCAACAUUAUUUUCUCUUCUUCCUCAGCUUCUCCAUGUUUAGGAACUGAGAAAGAAACUGCCUAAGCAGCACUUCCCCAUGUCCUUUCACCUUCAUGUUAACGUCCCUUCUGAUGGUCUCACUCUUCACAGGUAGUUCACACUCUGAGACUUGAAGUAAGCUCAUGGUUCAGUACUCUGGGGGCGCAGGGCUGCGCAGGACCCUUGGAAAUGUUGCAAGUGUUACUAGUACCAGUUUCACUUUUUGUUGUCACAAUUUACUGUAUUUUUUACUUUUUCUGUUACAGUUUUGCUAAUUUAUCAGAAGGUCCAAAAGUCUGACAUAACUAUUUCAUUUUGCAUUAUUUAUUUAUGAUGCUUUUUUCAUUGUCUUUUAUACAUUUGGGAUUAUAAAUUAUGUAAAUGUUAAAAUGAGCAUCUCAAAGAAGUCUGUUAAAUCAUGACUGAAAAAAAUCAAUCAGAUGUAUCUUCAAAAAGUGGAGUCCCAGUUUUAUGAAUCAGAGAUAUAAACCAGAAAUUCUAUAACUGAUCAUAGAAGAAGAAUCCAGUAAUUGAACAAAUCCUAUUUAAUGACAUCCUUGUAGCAUAGAUGGUCUAUAAUGCUGACCACAGAUUUCUUAGAAAUGCUGCUCUCUCUAUUUAACUAACAUUUUGUUCAGUUUUGCCUCCAGUGGAAGCAGAAAGGGUUUUUUCAGCUGUUAAAUCCUAAAAAUCAAUAUAAUUUAUUUAUGUAAGAAAAAUAACUCAAUCAAUAUAUUUUUGAACCUUUUAAGUACUAAUUUUCUUUUUAUCAAGUAGAAAAAAAAAUGUAUUUGCCCUAAAUCCUUAAAAUACAAAUGCUAUAAAAAUUCCUGUAUCUUGAAAGCCUUACUGCAAAUGAGUAUUAUAGACAUCCAGCAGAGUCUGGUUUUCUUUGUUGUCGUUGUGUUGUUGUUGUUUUGUAUGGAAAAGCUGCUUUCCCCGGGUUCCACUUAUAACCUCCGGUAGGUCACAGGGUUCAAUGUGGAUCUGACUUAAAAACCCACCAGCAUGCUCAAUCCCUUGUUAUCCUUAUGGAAUCUGUAUGUUAACUCUCUGGGUGUUCAGGCUUCUAUUUGACUGCUGUUGUGACCCUGUUUGCAAAAUGAAUAUGACACUCUGUGGAUUAUUUGCUCUGUAAGGCACAAGUGCUUCUUAUGAUUAUUUUGACGUUUCCAAGAGCAAAAGCCAAAUUUAAACUCUCUUCAGCAAACUUGAGCCUUUUCAUCUAAUUCCAUGUCACUCACGGCCAUAACUUUCCUUGACCAUUCUUCACCCCAUGUCUUACAUAAUAAAUUGUGGUCUUGAUCCUGGAUUUAAAAACAAAAGAAAAAGUUUAAAAGUCA